GCCAGAUCUUAGGCACCUGGCCGCCUGGAGCUGCUGGACAUGUCUCUGGGCUUGGCUGGGGGGCUGGAACGAGGGCAAAGAGCAGCCCCCAAGUCUUCCUGAAGCCGUGAAUGGCUGGCCUGUGGCAGGGUGCCCCUGGAGGCCGGCGGUGGGCCCUGGUGUUACUAAUGCUGAGAUACCUGCUGCCCACAGGAGGAAUUACUCAUCUGGACACCAGAGCCCUGCUAAGCCUGGUUGCAGCCACAGAAAUCCUGGGUGGUCACCAUGUACCCACAUCUCAGCCUUCUGCAGAAGACCUGUGCCCUGAUAUGCCCAUCUCCUGUGGGAGAACCCUGGGGACACGCUCACUGUCCAGAGUCAGGAACAUGAAUGAUGCUUCUGUGGACACCAAGAGGCAGCCAAACAAGAGAAAGCUGAUCAGAAGGGCAGCAUUCAGCCCAGUUCCUUCAAGGUCACCUGCGAGGCCAGAGGGUCCUAUGACUUCCUGGAGGCUGGACGCCAGAGGCCAGGGAUGGGACCCUGGAGGCCCCAGGAUCCCAGUGUAUCCCGUGCCCACUGAGCAGUCACAUCCUGCACACUCAGGGCUGAGGCACCAGCCACAUUCCCACACCAGGACCGGAGACAGGCUGCCUUUCGACGCAGUGGUCUUUGCCCAAACCACAGACCAAGGAACACUUGGAGCCACCAGGCAGUUGACCCACGACCCUUCCUCCCCGGCGUCACUCAUCAGCUCCGUGGGAACUCACGAGCCUGGGGAGAAUUCGUCAUCCCCACAUGGAACCUCAGUAUGGCCAACAGGCAGCCCUCUGGUAGAAAAAUCAACAAUCAGUCCUGCAGAUAAGACCUUGGCCAGUCCUACAUCUUCGGUUGUGGGAAGAACCACCCAGUCUUUGGGGGUGAUGUCCUCUGCUCUCCCUGAGUCAACCUCUAGAGGAAUGACACACUCCGAGCAAAGAACCAGCCCAUCGCUGAGUCCCCAGGUCAAUGGAACUCCCUCUAGGAACUACCCUGCUACAAGCAUGGUUUCAGGAUUGAGUUCCCCAAGGACCAGGACCAGUUCCACAGAAGGAAAUUUUACCAAAGAAGCAUCUACAUACACACUCACUGUAGAGACCACAAGUGGCCCAGUCACUGAGAAGUACACAGUCCCCACUGAGACCUCAACAACUGAAGGUGACAGCACAGAGACCCCCUGGGACACAAGAUAUAUUCCUGUAAAAAUCACAUCUCCAAUGAAAACAUUUGCAGAUUCAACUGCAUCCAAGGAAAAUGCCCCAGUGUCUAUGACUCCAGCUGAGACCACAGUUACUGACUCACAUACUCCAGGAAGGACAAACCCAUCAUUUGGGACACUUUAUUCUUCCUUCCUUGACCUAUCACCUAAAGGGACCCCAAAUUCCAGAGGUGAAACAAGCCUGGAACUGAUUCUAUCAACCACUGGAUAUCCCUUCUCCUCUCCUGAACCUGGCUCUGCAGGACACAGCAGAAUAAGUACCAGUGCGCCUUUGUCAUCAUCUGCUUCAGUUCUCGAUAAUAAAAUAUCAGAGACCAGCAUAUUCUCAGGCCAGAGUCUCACCUCCCCUCUGUCUCCUGGGGUGCCCGAGGCCAGAGCCAGCACAAUGCCCAACUCAGCUAUCCCUUUUUCCAUGACACUAAGCAAUGCAGAAACAAGUGCCGAAAGGGUCAGAAGCACAAUUUCCUCUCUGGGGACUCCAUCAAUAUCCACAAAGCAGACAGCAGAGACUAUCCUUACCUUCCAUGCCUUCGCUGAGACCAUGGAUAUACCCAGCACCCACAUAGCCAAGACUUUGGCUUCAGAAUGGUUGGGAAGUCCAGGUACCCUUGGUGGCACCAGCACUUCAGCGCUGACAACCACAUCUCCAUCUACCACUUUAGUCUCAGAGGAGACCAACACCCAUCACUCCACGAGUGGAAAGGAAACAGAAGGAACUUUGAAUACAUCUAUGACUCCACUUGAGACCUCUGCUCCUGGAGAAGAGUCCGAAAUGACUGCCACCUUGGUCCCCACUCUAGGUUUUACAACUCUUGACAGCAAGAUCAGAAGUCCAUCUCAGGUCUCUUCAUCCCACCCAACAAGAGAGCUCAGAACCACAGGCAGCACCUCUGGGAGGCAGAGUUCCAGCACAGCUGCCCACGGGAGCUCUGACAUCCUGAGGGCAACCACUUCCAGCACCUCAAAAGCAUCAUCAUGGACCAGUGAAAGCACAGCUCAGCAAUUUAGUGAACCCCAGCACACACAGUGGGUGGAGACAAGUCCUAGCAUGAAAACAGAGAGACCCCCAGCAUCAACCAGUGUGGCAGCCCCUAUCACCACUUCUGUUCCCUCAGUGGUCUCUGGCUUCACCACCCUGAAGACCAGCUCCACAAAAGGGAUUUGGCUUGAAGAAACAUCUGCAGACACACUCAUCGGAGAAUCCACAGCUGGCCCAACCACCCAUCAGUUUGCUGUUCCCACUGGGAUUUCAAUGACAGGAGGCAGCAGCACCAGGGGAAGCCAGGGCACAACCCACCUACUCACCAGAGCCACAGCAUCAUCUGAGACAUCCGCAGAUUUGACUCUGGCCACGAACGGUGUCCCAGUCUCCGUGUCUCCAGCAGUGAGCAAGACGGCUGCUGGCUCAAGUCCUCCAGGAGGGACAAAGCCAUCAUAUACAAUGGUUUCUUCUGUCAUCCCUGAGACAUCAUCUCUACAGUCCUCAGCUUUCAGGGAAGGAACCAGCCUGGGACUGACUCCAUUAAACACUAGACAUCCCUUCUCUUCCCCUGAACCAGACUCUGCAGGACACACCAAGAUAAGCACCAGCAUUCCUCUGUUGUCAUCUGCUUCAGUUCUUGAGGAUAAAGUGUCAGCGACCAGCACAUUCUCACACCACAAAGCCACCUCAUCUAUUACCACAGGGACUCCUGAAAUCUCAACAAAGACAAAGCCCAGCUCAGCCGUUCUUUCCUCCAUGACCCUAAGCAAUGCAGCAACAAGUCCUGAAAGAGUCAGAAAUGCAACUUCCCCUCUGACUCAUCCAUCUCCAUCAGGGGAAGAGACAGCAGGGAGUGUCCUCACUCUCAGCACCUCUGCUGAGACUACAGACUCACCUAACAUCCACCCAACUGGGACACUGACUUCAGAAUCGUCAGAGAGUCCUAGCACUCUCAGCCUCCCAAGUGUCUCUGGAGUCAAAACCACAUUUUCUUCAUCUACUCCUUCCACUCAUCUAUUUACUAGUGGAGAAGAAACAGAGGAAACUUCGAAUCCAUCUGUGUCUCAACCUGAGACUUCUGUUUCCAGAGUAAGGACCACCUUGGCCAGCACCUCUGUCCCUACCCCAGUAUUCCCCACCAUGGACACCUGGCCUACACGUUCAGCUCAGUUCUCUUCAUCCCACCUAGUGAGUGAGCUCAGAGCUACGAGCAGUACCUCAGUUACAAACUCAACUGGUUCAGCUCUUCCUAAAAUAUCUCACCUCACUGGGACGGCAACAAUGUCACAGACCAAUAGAGACACGUUUAAUGACUCUGCUGCACCCCAAAGCACAACUUGGCCAGAGACUAGUCCCAGAUUCAAGACAGGGUUACCUUCAGCAACAACCACUGUUUCAACCUCUGCCACUUCUCUCUCUGCUACUGUAAUGGUCUCUAAAUUCACUUCUCCAGCAACUAGUUCCAUGGAAGCAACUUCUAUCAGGGAACCAUCAACAACCAUCCUCACAACAGAGACCACGAAUGGCCCAGGCUCUAUGGCUGUGGCUUCUACCAACAUCCCAAUUGGAAAGGGCUACAUUACUGAAGGAAGAUUGGACACAAGCCAUCUGCCCAUUGGAACCACAGCUUCCUCUGAGACAUCUAUGGAUUUUACCAUGGCCAAAGAAAGUGUCUCAAUGUCAGUAUCUCCAUCUCAGUCCAUGGAUGCUGCUGGCUCAAGCACUCCAGGAAGGACAAGCCAAUUCGUUGACACAUUUUCUGAUGAUGUCUAUCAUUUAACAUCCAGAGAAAUUACAAUACCUAGAGAUGGAACAAGCUCAGCUCUGACUCCACAAAUGACUGCAACUCACCCUCCAUCUCCUGAUCCUGGCUCUGCUAGAAGCACCUGGCUUGGCAUCUUGUCCUCAUCUCCUUCUUCUCCUACUCCCAAAGUCACAAUGAGCUCCACAUUUUCAACUCAGAGAGUCACCACAAGCAUGAUAAUGGACACAGUUGAAACUAGUCGGUGGAACAUGCCCAACUUACCUUCCACGACUUCCUUGACACCAAGUAAUAUUCCAACAAGUGGUGCCAUAGGAAAAAGCACCCUGGUUCCCUUGGACACUCCAUCUCCAGCCACAUCAUUGGAGGCAUCAGAAGGGGGACUUCCAACCCUCAGCACCUACCCUGAAUCAACAAACACACCCAGCAUCCACCUCGGAGCACACGCUAGUUCAGAAAGUCCAAGCACCAUCAAACUUACCAUGGCUUCAGUAGUAAAACCUGGCUCUUACACACCUCUCACCUUCCCCUCAAUAGAGACCCACAUUCAUGUAUCAACAGCCAGAAUGGCUUACUCUUCUGGGUCUUCACCUGAGAUGACAGCUCCUGGAGAGACUAACACUGGUAGUACCUGGGACCCCACCACCUACAUCACCACUACGGAUCCUAAGGAUACAAGUUCAGCUCAGGUCUCUACACCCCACUCAGUGAGGACACUCAGAACCACAGAAAACCAUCCAAAGACAGAGUCCGCCACCCCAGCUGCUUACUCUGGAAGUCCUAAAAUCUCAAGUUCACCCAAUCUCACCAGUCCGGCCACAAAAGCAUGGACCAUCACAGACACAACUGAACACUCCACUCAAUUACAUUACACAAAAUUGGCAGAAAAAUCAUCUGGAUUUGAGACACAGUCAGCUCCAGGACCUGUCUCUGUAGUAAUCCCUACCUCCCCUACCAUUGGAAGCAGCACAUUGGAACUAACUUCUGAUGUCCCAGGGGAACCCCUGGUCCUUGCUCCCAGUGAGCAGACCACAAUCACUCUCCCCAUGGCAACAUGGCUGAGUACCAGUUUGACAGAGGAAAUGGCUUCAACAGACCUUGAUAUUUCAAGUCCAAGUUCACCCAUGAGUACAUUUGCUAUUUUUCCACCUAUGUCCACACCUUCUCAUGAACUUUCAAAGUCAGAGGCAGAUACCAGUGCCAUUAGAAAUACAGAUUCAACAACGUUGGAUCAGCACCUAGGAAUCAGGAGUUUGGGCAGAACUGGGGACUUAACAACUGUUCCUAUCACCCCACUGACAACCACGUGGACCAGUGUGAUUGAACACUCAACACAAGCACAGGACACCCUUUCUGCAACGAUGAGUCCUACUCACGUGACACAGUCACUCAAAGAUCAAACAUCUAUACCAGCCUCAGCAUCCCCUUCCCAUCUUACUGAAGUCUACCCUGAGCUCGGGACACAAGGGAGAAGCUCCUCUGAGGCAACCACUUUUUGGAAACCAUCUACAGACACACUGUCCAGAGAGAUUGAGACUGGCCCAACAAACAUUCAAUCCACUCCACCCAUGGACAACACAACAACAGGGAGCAGUAGUAGUGGAGUCACCCUGGGCAUAGCCCACCUUCCCAUAGGAACAUCCUCCCCAGCUGAGACAUCCACAAACAUGGCACUGGAAAGAAGAAGUUCUACAGCCACUGUCUCUAUGGCUGGGACAAUGGGACUCCUUGUUACUAGUGCUCCAGGAAGAAGCAUCAGCCAGUCAUUAGGAAGAGUUUCCUCUGUCCUUUCUGAGUCAACUACUGAAGGAGUCACAGAUUCUAGUAAGGGAAGCAGCCCAAGGCUGAACACACAGGGAAAUACAGCUCUCUCCUCCUCUCUUGAACCCAGCUAUGCUGAAGGAAGCCAGAUGAGCACAAGCAUCCCUCUAACCUCAUCUCCUACAACUCCUGAUGUGGAAUUCAUAGGGGGCAGCACAUUUUGGACCAAGGAGGUCACCACAGUUAUGACCUCAGACAUCUCCAAGUCUUCAGCAAGGACAGAGUCCAGCUCAGCUACCCUUAUGUCCACAGCUUUGGGAAGCACUGAAAAUACAGGAAAAGAAAAACUCAGAACUGCCUCUAUGGAUCUUCCAUCUCCAACUCCAUCAAUGGAGGUGACACCAUGGAUUUCUCUCACUCUCAGUAAUGCCCCCAAUACCACAGAUUCACUUGACCUCAGCCAUGGGGUGCACACCAGCUCUGCAGGGACUUUGGCCACUGACAGGUCAUUGAAUACUGGUGUCACUAGAGCCUCCAGAUUGGAAAACGGCUCUGAUACCUCUUCUAAGUCCCUGUCUAUGGGAAACAGCACUCACACUUCCAUGACUUACACAGAGAAGAGUGAAGUGUCUUCUUCAAUCCAUCCCCGACCUGAGACCUCAGCUCCUGGAGCAGAGACCACUUUGACUUCCACUCCUGGAAACAGGGCCAUAAGCUUAACAUUGCCUUUUUCAUCCAUUCCAGUGGAAGAAGUCAUUUCUACAGGCAUAACCUCAGGACCAGACAUCAACUCAGCACCCAUGACACAUUCUCCCAUCACCCCACCAACAAUUGUAUGGACCAGUACAGGCACAAUUGAACAGUCCACUCAACCACUACAUGCAGUUUCUUCAGAAAAAGUUUCUGUGCAGACACAGUCAACUCCAUAUGUCAACUCUGUGGCAGUGUCUGCUUCCCCUACCCAUGAGAAUUCAGUCUCUUCUGGAAGCAGCACAUCCUCUCCAUAUUCCUCAGCCUCACUUGAAUCCUUGGAUUCCACAAUCAGUAGGAGGAAUGCAAUCACUUCCUGGCUAUGGGACCUCACUACAUCUCUCCCCACUACAACUUGGCCAAGUACUAGUUUAUCUGAGGCACUGUCCUCAGGCCAUUCUGGGGUUUCAAACCCAAGUUCAACUACGACUGAAUUUCCACUCUUUUCAGCUGCAUCCACAUCUGCUGCUAAGCAAAGAAAUCCAGAAACAGAGACCCAUGGUCCCCAGAAUACAGCCGCGAGUACUUUGAACACUGAUGCAUCCUCGGUCACAGGUCUUUCUGAGACUCCUGUGGGGGCAAGUAUCAGCUCUGAAGUCCCUCUUCCAAUGGCCAUAACUUCUAGAUCAGAUGUUUCUGGCCUUACAUCUGAGAGUACUGCUAACCCGAGUUUAGGCACAGCCUCUUCAGCAGGGACCAAAUUAACUAGGACAAUAUCCCUGCCCACUUCAGAGUCUUUGGUUUCCUUUAGAAUGAACAAGGAUCCAUGGACAGUGUCAAUCCCUUUGGGGUCCCAUCCAACUACUAAUACAGAAACAAGCAUCCCAGUAAACAGCGCAGGUCCACCUGGCUUGUCCACAGUAGCAUCAGAUGUAAUUGACACACCUUCAGAUGGGGCUGAGAGUAUUCCCACUGUCUCCUUUUCCCCCUCCCCUGAUACUGAAGUGACAACUAUCUCACAUUUCCCAGAAAAGACAACUCAUUCAUUUAGAACCAUUUCAUCUCUCACUCAUGAGUUGACUUCAAGAGUGACACCUAUUCCUGGGGAUUGGAUGAGUUCAGCUAUGUCUACAAAGCCCACAGGAGCCAGUCCCUCCAUUACACUGGGAGAGAGAAGGACAAUCACCUCUGCUGCUCCAACCACUUCCCCCAUAGUUCUCACUGCUAGUUUCACAGAGACCAGCACAGUUUCACUGGAUAAUGAAACUACAGUAAAAACCUCAGAUAUCCUUGACGCACGGAAAACAAAUGAGCUCCCCUCAGAUAGCAGUUCUUCUUCUGAUCUGAUCAACACCUCCAUAGCUUCUUCAACUAUGGAUGUCACUAAAACAGCCUCCAUCAGUCCCACUAGCAUCUCAGGAAUGACAGCAAGUUCCUCCCCAUCUCUCUUCUCUUCAGAUAGACCCCAGGUUCCCACAUCUACAACAGAGACAAAUACAGCCACCUCUCCAUCUGUUUCCAGUAACACCUAUUCUCUUGAUGGGGGCUCCAAUGUGGGUGGCACUCCAUCCACUUUACCACCCUUUACAAUCACCCACCCUGUCGAGACAAGCUCGGCCCUAUUAGCCUGGUCUAGACCAGUAAGAACUUUCAGCACCAUGGUCAGCACUGACACUGCCUCCGGAGAAAAUCCUACCUCUAGCAAUUCUGUGGUGACUUCUGUUCCAGCACCAGGUACAUGGACCAGUGUAGGCAGUACUACUGACUUACCUGCCAUGGGCUUUCUCAAGACAAGUCCUGCAGGAGAGGCACACUCACUUCUAGCAUCAACUAUUGAACCAGCCACUGCCUUCACUCCCCAUCUCUCAGCAGCAGUGGUCACUGGAUCCAGUGCUACAUCAGAAGCCAGUCUUCUCACUACGAGUGAAAGCAAAGCCAUUCAUUCUUCACCACAGACCCCAACUACACCCACCUCUGGAGCAAACUGGGAAACUUCAGCUACUCCUGAGAGCCUUUUGGUAGUCACUGAGACUUCAGACACAACACUUACCUCAAAGAUUUUGGUCACAGAUACCAUCUUGUUUUCAACUGUGUCCACGCCACCUUCUAAAUUUCCAAGUACGGGGACUCUGUCUGGAGCUUCCUUCCCUACUUUACUCCCGGACACUCCAGCCAUCCCUCUCACUGCCACUGAGCCAACAAGUUCAUUAGCUACAUCCUUUGAUUCCACCCCACUGGUGACUAUAGCUUCGGAUAGUCUUGGCACAGUCCCAGAGACUACCCUGACCAUGUCAGAGACCUCAAAUGGUGAUGCACUGGUUCUUAAGACAGUAAGUAACCCAGAUAGGAGCAUCCCUGGAAUCACUAUCCAAGGAGUAACAGAAAGUCCACUCCAUCCUUCUUCCACUUCCCCCUCUAAGAUUGUUGCUCCACGGAAUACAACCUAUGAAGGUUCGAUCACAGUGGCACUUUCUACUUUGCCUGCGGGAACUACUGGUUCCCUUGUAUUCAGUCAGAGUUCUGAAAACUCAGAGACAACGGCUUUGGUAGACUCAUCAGCUGGGCUUGAGAGGGCAUCUGUGAUGCCACUAACCACAGGAAGCCAGGGUAUGGCUAGCUCUGGAGGAAUCAGAAGUGGGUCCACUCACUCAACUGGAACCAAAACAUUUUCUUCUCUCCCUCUGACCAUGAACCCAGGUGAGGUUACAGCCAUGUCUGAAAUCACCACGAACAGACUGACAGCUACUCAAUCAACAGCACCCAAAGGGAUACCUGUGAAGCCCACCAGUGCUGAGUCAGGCCUCCUAACACCUGUCUCUGCCUCCUCAAGCCCAUCAAAGGCCUUUGCCUCACUGACUACAGCUCCCCCAACUUGGGGGAUCCCACAGUCUACCUUGACAUUUGAGUUUUCUGAGGUCCCAAGUUUGGAUACUAAGUCCGCUUCUUUACCAACUCCUGGACAGUCCCUGAACACCAUUCCAGACUCAGAUGCAAGCACAGCAUCUUCCUCACUGUCCAAGUCUCCAGAAAAAAACCCAAGGGCAAGGAUGAUGACUUCCACAAAGGCCAUAAGUGCAAGCUCAUUUCAAUCAACAGGUUUUACUGAAACCCCUGAGGGAUCUGCCUCCCCUUCUAUGGCAGGGCAUGAACCCAGAGUCCCCACUUCAGGAACAGGGGACCCUAGAUAUGCCUCAGAGAGCAUGUCUUAUCCAGACCCAAGCAAGGCAUCAUCAGCUAUGACAUCGACCUCUCUUGCAUCAAAACUCACAACUCUCUUCAGCACAGGUCAAGCAGCAAGGUCUGGUUCUAGUUCCUCUCCCAUAAGCCUAUCCACUGAGAAAGAAACAAGCUUCCUUUCCCCCACUGCAUCCACCUCCAGAAAGACUUCACUAUUUCUUGGGCCUUCCAUGGCAAGGCAGCCCAACAUAUUGGUGCAUCUUCAGACUUCAGCUCUGACACUUUCUCCAACAUCCACUCUAAAUAUGUCCCAGGAGGAGCCUCCUGAGUUAACCUCAAGCCAGACCAUUGCAGAAGAAGAGGGAACAACAGCUGAAACACAGACGUUAACCUUCACACCAUCUGAGACCCCAACAUCCUUGUUACCUGUCUCUUCUCCCACAGAACCCACAGCCAGAAGAAAGAGUUCUCCAGAAACAUGGGCAAGCUCUAUUUCAGUUCCUGCCAAGACCUCCUUGGUUGAAACAACUGAUGGAACGCUAGUGACCACCAUAAAGAUGUCAAGCCAGGCAGCACAAGGAAAUUCCACGUGGCCUGCCCCAGCAGAGGAGACGGGGAGCAGUCCAGCAGGCACAUCCCCAGGAAGCCCAGAAAUGUCUACCACUCUCAAAAUCAUGAGCUCCAAGGAACCCAGCAUCAGCCCAGAGAUCAGGUCCACUGUGAGAAAUUCUCCUUGGAAGACUCCAGAAACAACUGUUCCCAUGGAGACCACAGUGGAACCAGUCACCCUUCAGUCCACAGCCCUAGGAAGUGGCAGCACCAGCAUCUCUCACCUGCCCACAGGAACCACAUCACCAACCAAGUCACCAACAGAAAAUAUGUUGGCUACAGAAAGGGUCUCCCUCUCCCCAUCCCCACCUGAGGCUUGGACCAACCUUUAUUCUGGAACUCCAGGAGGGACCAGGCAGUCACUGGCCACAAUGUCCUCUGUCUCCCUAGAGUCACCAACUGCUAGAAGCAUCACAGGGACUGGUCAGCAAAGCAGUCCAGAACUGGUUUCAAAGACAACUGGAAUGGAAUUCUCUAUGUGGCAUGGCUCUACUGGAGGGACCACAGGGGACACACAUGUCUCUCUGAGCACAUCUUCCAAUAUCCUUGAAGACCCUGUAACCAGCCCAAACUCUGUGAGCUCAUUGACAGAUAAAUCCAAACAUAAAACCGAGACAUGGGUAAGCACCACAGCCAUUCCCUCCACUGUCCUGAAUAAUAAGAUAAUGGCAGCUGAACAACAGACAAGUCGAUCUGUGGAUGAGGCUUAUUCAUCAACUAGUUCUUGGUCAGAUCAGACAUCUGGGAGUGACAUCACCCUUGGUGCAUCUCCUGAUGUCACAAACACAUUAUACAUCACCUCCACAGCACAAACCACCUCACUAGUGUCUCUGCCCUCUGGAGACCAAGGCAUUACAAGCCUCACCAAUCCCUCAGGAGGAAAAACAAGCUCUGCGUCAUCUGUCACAUCUCCUUCAAUAGGGCUUGAGACUCUGAGGGCCAAUGUAAGUGCAGUGAAAAGUGACAUUGCCCCUACUGCUGGGCAUCUAUCUCAGACUUCAUCUCCUGCGGAAGUGAGCAUCCUGGACGUAACCACAGCUCCUACUCCAGGUAUCUCCACCACCAUCACCACCAUGGGAACCAACUCAAUCUCAACUACCACACCCAACCCAGAAGUGGGUAUGAGUACCAUGGACAGCACCCCGGCCACAGAGAGGCGCACAACUUCUACAGAACACCCUUCCACCUGGUCUUCCACAGCUGCAUCAGAUUCCUGGACUGUCACAGACAUGACUUCAAACUUGAAAGUUGCAAGAUCUCCUGGAACAAUUUCCACAAUGCAUACAACUUCAUUCUUAGCCUCAAGCACUGAAUUAGACUCCAUGUCUACUCCCCAUGGCCGUAUAACUGUCAUUGGAACCAGCCUGGUCACUCCAUCCUCUGAUGCUUCAGCUGUAAAGACAGAGACCAGUACAAGUGAAAGAACAUUGAGUCCUUCAGACACAACUGCAUCUACUCCCAUCUCAACUUUUUCUCGUGUCCAGAGGAUGAGCAUCUCAGUUCCUGACAUUUUAAGUACAAGUUGGACUCCCAGUAGUACAGAAGCAGAAGAUGUGCCUGUUUCAAUGGUUUCUACAGAUCAUGCUAGUACAAAGACUGACCCAAAUACGCCCCUGUCCACUUUUCUGUUUGAUUCUCUGUCCACUCUUGACUGGGACACUGGGAGAUCUCUGUCAUCAGCCACAGCCACUACCUCAGCUCCUCAGGGGGCCACAACUCCCCAGGAACUCACUUUGGAAACCAUGAUCAGCCCAGCUACCUCACAGUUGCCCUUCUCUAUAGGGCACAUUACAAGUGCAGUCACACCAGCUGCAAUGGCAAGGAGCUCUGGAGUUACUUUUUCAAGACCAGAUCCCACAAGCAAAAAGGCAGAGCAGACUUCCACUCAGCUUCCCACCACCACUUCUGCACAUCCAGGGCAGGUGCCCAGAUCAGCAGCAACAACUCUGGAUGUGAUCCCACACACAGCAAAAACUCCAGAUGCAACUUUUCAGAGACAAGGGCAGACAGCUCUUACAACAGAGGCAAGAGCUACAUCUGACUCCUGGAAUGAGAAAGAAAAAUCAACCCCAAGUGCACCUUGGAUCACUGAGAUGAUGAAUUCUGUCUCAGAAGAUACCAUCAAGGAGGUUACCAGCUCCUCCAGUGUAUUAAGGACCCUGAAUACGCUGGACAUAAACUUGGAAUCUGGGACGACUUCAUCCCCAAGUUGGAAAAGCAGCCCAUAUGAGAGAAUUGCCCCUUCUGAGUCCACCACAGACAAAGAGGCAAUUCACCCUUCUACAAACACAGUAGAGACCACAGGCUGGGUCACAAGUUCCGAACAUGCUUCUCAUUCCACUAUCCCAGCCCACUCAGCGUCAUCCAAACUCACAUCUCCAGUGGUUACAACCUCCACCAGGGAACAAGCAAUAGUUUCUAUGUCAACAACCACAUGGCCAGAGUCUACAAGGGCUAGAACAGAGCCUAAUUCCUUCUUGACUAUUGAACUGAGGGACGUCAGCCCUUACAUGGACACCAGCUCAACCACACAAACAAGUAUUAUCUCUUCCCCAGGUUCCACUGCGAUCACCAAGGGGCCUAGAACAGAAAUUACCUCCUCUAAGAGAAUAUCCAGCUCAUUCCUUGCCCAGUCUAUGAGGUCGUCAGACAGCCCCUCAGAAGCCAUCACCAGGCUGUCUAACUUUCCUGCCAUGACAGAAUCUGGAGGAAUGAUCCUUGCUAUGCAAACAAGUCCACCUGGCGCUACAUCACUAAGUGCACCUACUUUGGAUACAUCAGCCACAGCCUCCUGGACAGGGACUCCACUGGCUACGACUCAGAGAUUUACAUACUCAGAGAAGACCACUCUCUUUAGCAAAGGUCCUGAGGAUACAUCACAGCCAAGCCCUCCCUCUGUGGAAGAAACCAGCUCUUCCUCUUCCCUGGUACCUAUCCAUGCUACAACCUCGCCUUCCAAUAUUUUGUUGACAUCACAAGGGCACAGUCCCUCCUCUACUCCACCUGUGACCUCAGUUUUCUUGUCUGAGACCUCUGGCCUGGGGAAGACCACAGACAUGUCGAGGAUAAGCUUGGAACCUGGCACAAGUUUACCUCCCAAUUUGAGCAGUACAGCAGGUGAGGCGUUAUCCACUUAUGAAGCCUCCAGAGAUACAAAGGCAAUUCAUCAUUCUGCAGACACAGCAGUGACGAAUAUGGAGGCAACCAGUUCUGAAUAUUCUCCUAUCCCAGGCCAUACAAAGCCAUCCAAAGCCACAUCUCCAUUGGUUACCUCCCACAUCAUGGGGGACAUCACUUCUUCCACAUCAGUAUUUGGCUCCUCCGAGACCACAGAGAUUGAGACAGUGUCCUCUGUGAACCAGGGACUUCAGGAGAGAAGCACAUCCCAGGUGGCCAGCUCUGCUACAGAGACAAGCACUGUCAUUACCCAUGUGUCUAGUGGUGAUGCUACUACUCAUGUCACCAAGACACAAGCCACUUUCUCUAGCGGAACAUCCAUCUCAAGCCCUCAUCAGUUUAUAACUUCUACCAACACAUUUACAGAUGUGAGCACCAACCCCUCCACCUCUCUGAUAAUGACAGAAUCUUCAGGAGUGACCAUCACCACCCAAACAGGUCCUACUGGAGCUGCAACACAGGGUCCAUAUCUCUUGGACACAUCAACCAUGCCUUACUUGACAGAGACUCCAUUAGCUGUGACUCCAGAUUUUAUGCAAUCAGAGAAGACCACUCUCAUAAGCAAAGGUCCCAAGGAUGUGUCCUGGACAAGCCCUCCCUCUGUGGCAGAAACCAGCUAUCCCUCUUCCCUGACACCUUUCUUGGUCACAACCAUACCUCCUGCCACUUCCACGUUACAAGGGCAACAUACAUCCUCUCCUGUUUCUGCGACUUCAGUUCUUACCUCUGGACUGGUGAAGACCACAGAUAUGUUGAACACAAGCAUGGAACCUGUGACCAAUUCACCUCAAAAUUUGAACAAUCCAUCAAAUGAGAUACUGGCCACUUUGGCAGCCACCACAGAUAUAGAGACUAUUCAUCCUUCCAUAAACAAAGCAGUGACCAAUAUGGGGACUGCCAGUUCAGCACAUGUACUGCAUUCCACUCUCCCAGUCAGCUCAGAACCAUCUACAGCCACAUCUCCAAUGGUUCCUGCCUCCAGCAUGGGGGACGCUCUUGCUUCUAUAUCAAUACCUGGUUCUGAGACCACAGACAUUGAGGGAGAGCCAACAUCCUCCCUGACUGCUGGACGAAAAGAGAACAGCACCCUCCAGGAGAUGAACUCAACUACAGAGUCAAACAUCAUCCUCUCCAAUGUGUCUGUGGGGGCUAUUACUGAAGCCACAAAAAUGGAAGUCCCCUCUUUUGAUGCAACAUUCAUACCAACUCCUGCUCAGUCAACAAAGUUCCCAGAUAUUUUCUCAGUAGCCAGCAGUAGACUUUCAAACUCUCCUCCCAUGACAAUAUCUACCCACAUGACCACCACCCAGACAGGGUCUUCUGGAGCUACAUCAAAGAUUCCACUUGCCUUAGACACAUCAACCUUGGAAACCUCAGCAGGGACUCCAUCAGUGGUGACUGAGGGGUUUGCCCACUCAAAAAUAACCACUGCAAUGAACAAUGAUGUCAAGGACGUGUCACAGACAAACCCUCCCUUUCAGGAUGAAGCCAGCUCUCCCUCUUCUCAAGCACCUGUCCUUGUCACAACCUUACCUUCUUCUGUUGCUUUCACACCGCAAUGGCACAGUACCUCCUCUCCUGUUUCUAUGUCCUCAGUUCUUACUUCUUCACUGGUAAAGACCGCAGGCAAGGUGGAUACAAGCUUAGAAACAGUGACCAGUUCACCUCAAAGUAUGAGCAACACUUUGGAUGACAUAUCGGUCACUUCAGCAGCCACCACAGAUAUAGAGACAACGCAUCCUUCCAUAAACACAGUAGUUACCAAUGUGGGGACCACCGGUUCAGCAUUUGAAUCACAUUCUACUGUCUCAGCUUACCCAGAGCCAUCUAAAGUCACAUCUCCAAAUGUUACCACCUCCACCAUGGAAGACACCACAAUUUCCAGAUCAAUACCUAAAUCCUCUAAGACUACAAGAACUGAGACUGAGACAACUUCCUCCCUGACUCCUAAACUGAGGGAGACCAGCAUCUCCCAGGAGAUCACCUCGUCCACAGAGACAAGCACUGUUCCUUACAAAGAGCUCACUGGUGCCACUACCGAGGUAUCCAGGACAGAUGUCACUUCCUCUAGCAGUACAUCCUUCCCUGGCCCUGAUCAGUCCACAGUGUCACUAGACAUCUCCACAGAAACCAACACCAGGCUGUCUACCUCCCCAAUAAUGACAGAAUCUGCAGAAAUAACCAUCACCACCCAAACAGGUCCUCAUGGGGCUACAUCACAGGAUACUUUUACCAUGGACCCAUCAAAUACAACCCCCCAGGCAGGGAUCCACUCAGCUAUGACUCAUGGAUUUUCACAAUUGGAUGUGACCACUCUUAUGAGCAGAAUUCCACAGGAUGUAUCAUGGACAAGUCCUCCCUCUGUGGAUAAAACCAGCUCCCCCUCUUCCUUUCUGUCCUCACCUGCAAUGACCACACCUUCCCUGAUUUCUUCUACCUUACCAGAGGAUAAGCUCUCCUCUCCUAUGACUUCACUUCUCACCUCUGGCCUAGUGAAGAUUACAGACAUAUUACGUACACGCUUGGAACCUGUGACCAGCUCACUUCCAAAUUUCAGCAGCACCUCAGAUAAGAUACUGGCCACUUCUAAAGACAGUAAAGACACAAAGGAAAUUUUUCCUUCUAUAAACACAGAAGAGACCAAUGUGAAAGCCAACAACUCUGGACAUGAAUCCCAUUCCCCUGCACUGGCUGACUCAGAGACACCCAAAGCCACAACUCAAAUGGUUAUCACCACCACUGUGGGAGAUCCAGCUCCUUCCACAUCAAUGCCAGUGCAUGGUUCCUCUGAGACUACAAACAUUAAGAGAGAGCCAACAUAUUUCUUGACUCCUAGACUGAGAGAGACCAGUACCUCUCAGGAGUCCAGCUUUCCCACGGACACAAGUUUUCUACUUUCCAAAGUCCCCACUGGUACUAUUACUGAGGUCUCCAGUACAGGGGUCAACUCUUCUAGCAAAAUUUCCACCCCAGACCAUGAUAAGUCCACAGUGCCACCUGACACCUUCACAGGAGAGAUCCCCAGGGUCUUCACCUCCUCUAUUAAGACAAAAUCUGCAGAAAUGACGAUCACCACCCAAGCAAGUCCUCCUGAGUCUGCAUCGCACAGUACCCUUCCCUUGGACACAUCAACCACACUUUCCCAGGGAGGGACUCAUUCAACUGUGACUCAGGGAUUCCCAUACUCAGAGGUGACCACUCUCAUGGGCAUGGGUCCUGGGAAUGUGUCAUGGAUGACAACUCCCCCUGUGGAAGAAACCAGCUCUGUGUCUUCCCUGAUGUCUUCACCUGCCAUGACAUCCCCUUCUCCUGUUUCCUCCACAUCACCACAGAGCAUCCCCUCCUCUCCUCUUCCUGUGACUGCACUUCCUACUUCUGUUCUGGUGACAACCACAGAUGUGUUGGGCACAACAAGCCCAGAGUCUGUAACCAGUUCACCUCCAAAUUUGAGCAGCAUCACUCAUGAGAGACCGGCCACUUACAAAGACACUGCACACACAGAAGCCGCCAUGCAUCAUUCCACAAACACCGCAGUGACCAAUGUAGGGACUUCCGGGUCUGGACAUAAAUCACAAUCCUCUGUCCUAGCUGACUCAGAGACAUCGAAAGCCACACCUCUGAUGAGUACCACCUCCACCCUGGGGGACACAAGUGUUUCCACAUCAACUCCUAAUAUCUCUCAGACUAACCAAAUUCAAACAGAGCCAACAGCAUCCCUGAGCCCUAGACUGAGGGAGAGCAGCACGUCUGAGAAGACCAGCUCAACAACAGAGACAAAUACUGCCUUUUCUUAUGUGCCCACAGGUGCUAUUACUCAGGCCUCCAGAACAGAAAUCUCCUCUAGCAGAACAUCCAUCUCAGACCUUGAUCGGCCCACAAUAGCACCCGACAUCUCCACAGGAAUGAUCACCAGGCUCUUCACCUCCCCCAUCAUGACAAAAUCUGCAGAAAUGACCGUCACCACUCAAACAACUACUCCUGGGGCUACAUCACAGGGUAUCCUUCCCUGGGACACAUCAACCACACUUUUCCAGGGAGGGACUCAUUCAACCGUGUCUCAGGGAUUCCCACACUCAGAGAUAACCACUCUUCGGAGCAGAACCCCUGGAGAUGUGUCAUGGAUGACAACUCCCCCUGUGGAAGAAACCAGCUCUGGGUUUUCCCUGAUGUCACCUUCCAUGACAUCCCCUUCUCCUGUUUCCUCCACAUCACCAGAGAGCAUCCCCUCCUCUCCUCUCCCUGUGACUGCACUUCUUACUUCUGUUCUGGUGACAACCACAAAUGUAUUGGGCACAACAAGCCCAGAGCCCGUAACGAGUUCACCUCCAAAUUUAAGCAGCCCCACACAGGAGAGACUGACCACUUACAAAGACACUGCGCACACAGAAGCCAUGCAUGCUUCCAUGCAUACAAACACUGCAGUGGCCAACGUGGGGACCUCCAUUUCUGGACAUGAAUCACAAUCUUCUGUCCCAGCUGAUUCACACACAUCCAAAGCCACAUCUCCAAUGGGUAUCACCUUCGCCAUGGGGGAUACAAGUGUUUCUACAUCAACUCCUGCCUUCUUUGAGACUAGAAUUCAGACUGAAUCAACAUCCUCUUUGAUUCCUGGAUUAAGGGACACCAGGACGUCUGAGGAGAUCAACACUGUGACAGAGACCAGCACUGUCCUUUCAGAAGUGCCCACUACUACUACUACUGAGGUCUCCAGGACAGAAGUUAUCACUUCCAGCAGAACAACCAUCUCAGGGCCUGAUCAUUCCAAAAUGUCACCCUACAUCUCCACAGAAACCAUCACCAGGCUCUCCACUUUUCCUUUUGUAACAGGAUCCACAGAAAUGGCCAUCACCAACCAAACAGGUCCUAUAGGGACUAUCUCACAGGCUACCCUUACCCUGGACACAUCAAGCACAGCUUCCUGGGAAGGGACUCACUCACCUGUGACUCAGAGAUUUCCACACUCAGAGGAGACCACUACUAUGAGCAGAAGUACUAAGGGCGUGUCAUGGCAAAGCCCUCCCUCUGUGGAAGAAACCAGUUCUCCUUCUUCCCCAGUGCCUUUACCUGCAAUAACCUCACAUUCAUCUCUUUAUUCCGCAGUAUCAGGAAGUAGCCCCACUUCUGCUCUCCCUGUGACUUCCCUUCUCACCUCUGGCAGGAGGAAGACCAUAGACAUGUUGGACACACACUCAGAACUUGUGACCAGCUCCUUACCAAGUGCAAGUAGCUUCUCAGGUGAGAUACUCACUUCUGAAGCCUCCACAAAUACAGAGACAAUUCACUUUUCAGAGAACACAGCAGAAACCAAUAUGGGGACCACCAAUUCUAUGCAUAAACUACAUUCCUCUGUCUCAAUCCACUCCCAGCCAUCCGGACACACACCUCCAAAGGUUACUGGAUCUAUGAUGGAGGACGCUAUUGUUUCCACAUCAACACCUGGUUCUCCUGAGACUAAAAAUGUUGACAGAGACUCAACAUCCCCUCUGACUCCUGAACUGAAAGAGGACAGCACCGCCCUGGUGAUGAACUCAACUACAGAGUCAAACACUGUUUUCUCCAGUGUGUCCCUGGAUGCUGCUACUGAGGUCUCCAGGGCAGAAGUCACCUACUAUGAUCCUACAUUCAUGCCAGCUUCUGCUCAGUCAACAAAGUCCCCAGACAUUUCACCUGAAGCCAGCAGCAGUCAUUCUAACUCUCCUCCCUUGACAAUAUCUACACACAAGACCAUCGCCACACAAACAGGUCCUUCUGGGGUGACAUCUCUUGGCCAACUGACCCUGGACACAUCAACCAUAGCCACCUCAGCAGGAACUCCAUCAGCCAGAACUCAGGAUUUUGUAGAUUCAGAAACAACCAGUGUCAUGAACAAUGAUCUCAAUGAUGUGUUGAAGACAAGCCCUUUCUCUGCAGAAGAAGCCAACUCUCUCUCUUCUCAGGCACCUCUCCUUGUGACAACCUCACCUUCUCCUGUAACUUCCACAUUGCAAGAGCACAGUACCUCCUCUCUUGUUUCUGUGACCUCAGUACCCACCCCUACACUGGCGAAGAUCACAGACAUGGACACAAACUUAGAACCUGUGACUCGUUCACCUCAAAAUUUAAGGAACACCUUGGCCACUUCAGAAGCCACCACAGAUACACACACAAUGCAUCCUUCUAUAAACACAGCAGUGGCCAAUGUGGGGACCACCAGUUCACCAAAUGAAUUCUAUUUUACUGUCUCACCUGACUCAGACCCAUAUAAAGCCACAUCCGCAGUAGUUAUCACUUCCACCUCGGGGGACUCAAUAGUUUCCACAUCAAUGCCUAGAUCCUCUGCGAUGAAAAAGAUUGAGUCUGAGACAACUUUCUCCCUGAUAUUUAGACUGAGGGAGACUAGCACCUCCCAGAAAAUUGGCUCAUCCUCAGACACAAGCACGGUCUUUGACAAAGCAUUCACUGCUGCUACUACUGAGGUCUCCAGAACAGAACUCACCUCCUCUAGCAGAACAUCCAUCCAAGGCACUGAAAAGCCCACAAUGUCACCGGACACCUCCACAAGAUCUGUCACCAUGCUUUCUACUUUUGCUGGCCUGACAAAAUCCGAAGAAAGGACCAUUGCCACCCAAACAGGUCCUCAUAGGGCGACAUCACAGGGUACCCUUACCUGGGACACAUCAAUCACAACCUCACAGGCAGGGACCCACUCAGCUAUGACUCAUGGAUUUUCACAAUUAGAUUUGUCCACUCUUACGAGUAGAGUUCCUGAGUACAUAUCAGGGACAAGCCCACCCUCUGUGGAAAAAACCAGCUCUUCCUCUUCCCUUCUGUCUUUACCAGCAAUAACCUCACCGUCCCCUGUACCUACUACAUUACCAGAAAGUAGGCCGUCUUCUCCUGUUCAUCUGACUUCACUCCCCACCUCUGGCCUAGUGAAGACCACAGAUAUGCUGGCAUCUGUGGCCAGUUUACCUCCAAACUUGGGCAGCACCUCACAUAAGAUACCGACUACUUCAGAAGACAUUAAAGAUACAGAGAAAAUGUAUCCUUCCACAAACAUAGCAGUAACCAAUGUGGGGACCACCACUUCUGAAAAGGAAUCUUAUUCGUCUGUCCCAGCCUACUCAGAACCACCCAAAGUCACCUCUCCAAUGGUUACCUCUUUCAACAUAAGGGACACCAUUGUUUCCACAUCCAUGCCUGGCUCCUCUGAGAUUACAAGGAUUGAGAUGGAGUCAACAUUCUCCCUGGCUCAUGGGCUGAAGGGAACCAGCACCUCCCAGGACCCCAUCGUAUCCACAGAGAAAAGUGCUGUCCUUCACAAGUUGACCACUGGUGCUACUGAGACCUCUAGGACAGAAGUUGCCUCUUCUAGAAGAACAUCCAUUCCAGGCCCUGAUCAUUCCACAGAGUCACCAGACAUCUCCACUGAAGUGAUCCCCAGCCUGCCUAUCUCCCUUGGCAUUACAGAAUCUUCAAAUAUGACCAUCAUCACUCGAACAGGUCCUCCUCUUGGCUCUACAUCACAGGGCACAUUUACCUUGGACACACCAACUACAUCCUCCAGGGCAGGAACACACUCGAUGGCGACUCAGGAAUUUCCACACUCAGAAAUGACCACUGUCAUGAACAAGGACCCUGAGAUUCUAUCAUGGACAAUCCCUCCUUCUAUAGAGAAAACCAGCUUCUCCUCUUCCCUGAUGCCUUCACCAGCCAUGACUUCACCUCCUGUUUCCUCAACAUUACCAAAGACCAUUCACACCACUCCUUCUCCUAUGACCUCACUGCUCACCCCUAGCCUAGUGAUGACCACAGACACAUUGGGCACAAGCCCAGAACCUACAACCAGUUCACCUCCAAAUUUGAGCAGUACCUCACAUGAGAUACUGACAACAGAUGAAGACACCACAGCUAUAGAAGCCAUGCAUCCUUCCACAAGCACAGCAGCGACUAAUGUGGAAACCACCAGUUCUGGACAUGGGUCACAAUCCUCUGUCCUAGCUGACUCAGAAAAAACCAAGGCCACAGCUCCAAUGGAUACCACCUCCACCAUGGGGCAUACAACUGUUUCCACAUCAAUGUCUGUUUCCUCUGAGACUACAAAAAUUAAGAGAGAGUCAACAUAUUCCUUGACUCCUGGACUGAGAGAGACCAGCAUUUCCCAAAAUGCCAGCUUUUCCACUGACACAAGUAUUGUUCUUUCAGAAGUCCCCACUGGUACUACUGCUGAGGUCUCCAGGACAGAAGUCACCUCCUCUGGUAGAACAUCCAUCCCUGGCCCUUCUCAGUCCACAGUUUUGCCAGAAAUAUCCACAAGAACAAUGACAAGGCUCUUUGCCUCGCCCACCAUGACAGAAUCAGCAGAAAUGACCAUCCCCACUCAAACAGGUCCUUCUGGGUCUACCUCACAGGAUACCCUUACCUUGGACACAUCCACCACAAAGUCCCAGGCAAAGACUCAUUCAACUUUGACUCAGAGAUUUCCACACUCAGAGAUGACCACUCUCAUGAGCAGAGGUCCUGGAGAUAUGUCAUGGCAAAGCUCUCCCUCUCUGGAAAAUCCCAGCUCUCUCCCUUCCCUGCUGUCUUUACCUGCCACAACCUCACCUCCUCCCAUUUCCUCCACAUUACCAGUGACUAUCUCCUCCUCUCCUCUUCCUGUGACUUCACUUCUCACCUCUAGCCCGGUAACGACCACAGACAUGUUACACACAAGCCCAGAACUUGUAACCAGUUCACCUCCAAAGCUGAGCCACACUUCAGAUGAGAGACUGACCACUGGCAAGGACACCACAAAUACAGAAGCUGUGCAUCCUUCCACAAACACAGCAGCGUCCAAUGUGGAGAUUCCCAGCUCUGGACAUGAAUCCCCUUCCUCUGCCUUAGCUGACUCAGAGACAUCCAAAGCCACAUCACCAAUGUUUAUUACCUCCACCCAGGAGGAUACAACUGUUGCCAUAUCAACCCCUCACUUCUUGGAGACUAGCAGAAUUCAGAAAGAGUCAAUUUCCUCCCUGAGCCCUAAAUUGAGGGAGACAGGCAGUUCUGUGGAGACAAGCUCAGCCAUAGAGACAAGUGCUGUCCUUUCUGAAGUGUCCAUUGGUGCUACUACUGAGAUCUCCAGGACAGAAGUCACCUCCUCUAGCAGAACAUCCAUCUCUGGUUCUGCUGAGUCCACAAUGUUGCCAGAAAUAUCCACCACAAGAAAAAUCAUUAAGUUCCCUACUUCCCCCAUCCUGGCAGAAUCAUCAGAAAUGACCAUCAAGACCCAAACAAGUCCUCCUGGGUCUACAUCAGAGAGUACCUUUACAUUAGACACAUCAACCACUCCCUCCUUGGUAAUAACCCAUUCGACUAUGACUCAGAGAUUGCCACACUCAGAGAUAACCACUCUUGUGAGUAGAGGUGCUGGGGAUGUGCCACGGCCCAGCUCUCUCCCUGUGGAAGAAACAAGCCCUCCAUCUUCCCAGCUGUCUUUAUCUGCCAUGAUCUCACCUUCUCCUGUUUCUUCCACAUUACCAGCAAGUAGCCACUCCUCUUCUGCUUCUGUGACUUCACUUCUCACACCAGGCCAAGUGAAGACUACUGAGGUGUUGGACGCAAGUGCAGAACCUGAAACCAGUUCACCUCCAAGUUUGAGCAGCACCUCAGUUGAAAUACUGGCCACCUCUGAAGUCACCACAGAUACGGAGAAAAUUCAUCCUUUCUCAAACACGGCAGUAACCAAAGUUGGAACUUCCAGUUCUGGACAUGAAUCCCCUUCCUCUGUCCUACCUGACUCAGAGACAACCAAAGCCACAUCGGCAAUGGGUACCAUCUCCAUUAUGGGGGAUACAAGUGUUUCUACAUUAACUCCUGCCUUAUCUAACACUAGGAAAAUUCAGUCAGAGCCAGCUUCCUCACUGACCACCAGAUUGAGGGAGACCAGCACCUCUGAAGAGACCAGCUUAGCCACAGAAGCAAACACUGUUCUUUCUAAAGUGUCCACUGGUGCUACUACUGAGGUCUCCAGGACAGAAGCCAUCUCCUUUAGCAGAACAUCCAUGUCAGGCCCUGAGCAGUCCACAAUGUCACAAGACAUCUCCAUAGGAACCAUCCCCAGGAUUUCUGCCUCCUCUGUCCUGACAGAAUCUGCAAAAAUGACCAUCACAACCCAAACAGGUCCUUCGGAGUCUACACUAGAAAGUACCCUUAAUUUGAACACAGCAACCACACCCUCUUGGGUGGAAACCCACUCUAUAGUAAUUCAGGGAUUUCCACACCCAGAGAUGACCACUUCCAUGGGCAGAGGUCCUGGAGGUGUGUCAUGGCCUAGCCCUCCCUUUGUGAAAGAAACCAGCCCUCCAUCCUCCCCGCUGUCUUUACCUGCCGUGACCUCACCUCAUCCUGUUUCCACCACAUUCCUAGCACAUAUCCCCCCCUCUCCCCUUCCUGUGACUUCACUUCUCACCUCUGGCCCGGCGACAACCACAGAUAUCUUGGGUACAAGCACAGAACCUGGAACCAGUUCAUCUUCAAGUUUGAGCACCACCUCCCAUGAGAGACUGACCACUUACAAAGACACUGCACAUACAGAAGCCGUGCAUCCUUCCACAAACACAGGAGGGACCAAUGUGGCAACCACCAGCUCUGGAUAUAAAUCACAGUCCUCUGUCCUAGCUGACUCAUCUCCAAUGUGUACCACCUCCACCAUGGGGGAUACAAGUGUUCUCACAUCAACUCCUGCCUUCCUUGAGACUAGGAGGAUUCAGACAGAGCUAGCUUCCUCCCUGACCCCUGGAUUGAGGGAGUCCAGCGGCUCUGAAGGGACCAGCUCAGGCACCAAGAUGAGCACUGUCCUCUCUAAAGUGCCCACUGGUGCUACUACUGAGAUCUCCAAGGAAGACGUCACCUCCAUCCCAGGUCCCGCUCAAUCCACAAUAUCACCAGACAUCUCCACAAGAACCGUCAGCUGGUUCUCUACAUCCCCUGUCAUGACAGAAUCAGCAGAAAUAACCAUGAACACCCAUACAAGUCCUUUAGGGGCCACAACACAAGGCACCAGUACUUUGGACACGUCAAGCACAACCUCUUUGACAAUGACACACUCAACUAUAUCUCAAGGAUUUUCACACUCACAGAUGAGCACUCUUAUGAGGAGGGGUCCUGAGGAUGUAUCAUGGAUGAGCCCUCCCCUUCUGGAAAAAACUAGACCUUCCUUUUCUCUGAUGUCUUCACCAGCCACAACUUCACCUUCUCCUGUUUCCUCCACAUUACCAGAGAGCAUCUCUUCCUCUCCUCUUCCUGUGACUUCACUCCUCACGUCUGGCUUGGCAAAAACUACAGAUAUGUUGCACAAAAGCUCAGAACCUGUAACCAACUCACCUGCAAAUUUGAGCAGCACCUCAGUUGAAAUACUGGCCACCUCUGAAGUCACCACAGAUACAGAGAAAACUCAUCCUUCUUCAAACAGAACAGUGACCGAUGUGGGGACCUCCAGUUCUGGACAUGAAUCCACUUCCUUUGUCCUAGCUGACUCACAGACAUCCAAAGUCACAUCUCCAAUGGUUAUUACCUCCACCAUGGAGGAUACGAGUGUCUCCACAUCAACUCCUGGCUUUUUUGAGACUAGCAGAAUUCAGACAGAACCAACAUCCUCCCUGACCCUUGGACUGAGAAAGACCAGCAGCUCUGAGGGGACCAGCUUAGCCACAGAGAUGAGCACUGUCCUUUCUGGAGUGCCCACUGGUGCCACUGCUGAAGUCUCCAGGACAGAAGUCACCUCCUCUAGCAGAACAUCCAUCUCAGGCUUUGCUCAGCUCACAGUGUCACCAGAGACUUCCACAGAAACCAUCACCAGACUCCCUACCUCCAGCAUAAUGACAGAAUCAGCAGAAAUGAUGAUCAAGACACAAACAGAUCCUCCUGGGUCUACACCAGAGAGUACUCAUACUGUGGACAUAUCAACAACACCCAACUGGGUAGAAACCCACUCGACUGUGACUCAGAGAUUUUCACACUCAGAGAUGACCACUCUUGUGAGCAGAAGCCCUGGUGAUAUGUUAUGGCCUAGUCAAUCCUCUGUGGAAGAAACCAGCUCUGCCUCUUCCCUGCUGUCUCUGCCUGCCACGACCUCACCUUCUCCUGUUUCCUCUACAUUAGUAGAGGAUUUCCCUUCCGCUUCUCUUCCUGUGACUUCUCUUCUCAACCCUGGCCUGGUGAUAACCACAGACAGGAUGGGCAUAAGCAGAGAACCUGGAACCAGUUCCACUUCAAAUUUGAGCAGCACCUCCCAUGAGAGACUGACCACUUUGGAAGACACUGUAGAUACAGAAGACAUGCAGCCUUCCACACACACAGCAGUGACCAACGUGAGGACCUCCAUUUCUGGACAUGAAUCACAAUCUUCUGUCCUAUCUGACUCAGAGACACCCAAAGCCACAUCUCCAAUGGGUACCACCUACACCAUGGGGGAAACGAGUGUUUCCAUAUCCACUUCUGACUUCUUUGAGACCAGCAGAAUUCAGAUAGAACCAACAUCCUCCCUGACUUCUGGAUUGAGGGAGACCAGCAGCUCUGAGAGGAUCAGCUCAGCCACAGAGGGAAGCACUGUCCUUUCUGAAGUGCCCAGUGGUGCUACCACUGAGGUCUCCAGGACAGAAGUGAUAUCCUCUAGGGGAACAUCCAUGUCAGGGCCUGAUCAGUUCACCAUAUCACCAGACAUCUCUACUGAAGCGAUCACCAGGCUUUCUACUUCCCCCAUUAUGACAGAAUCAGCAGAAAGUGCCAUCACUAUUGAGACAGGUUCUCCUGGGGCUACAUCAGAGGGUACCCUCACCUUGGACACCUCAACAACAACCUUUUGGUCAGGGACCCACUCAACUGCAUCUCCAGGAUUUUCACACUCAGAGAUGACCACUCUUAUGAGUAGAACUCCUGGAGAUGUGCCAUGGCCGAGCCUUCCCUCUGUGGAAGAAGCCAGCUCUGUCUCUUCCUCACUGUCUUCACCUGCCAUGACCUCAACUUCUUUUUUCUCCACAUUACCAGAGAGCAUCUCCUCCUCUCCUCAUCCUGUGACUGCACUUCUCACCCUUGGCCCAGUGAAGACCACAGACAUGUUGCGCACAAGCUCAGAACCUGAAACCAGUUCACCUCCAAAUUUGAGCAGCACCUCAGCUGAAAUAUUAGCCACGUCUGAAGUCACCAAAGAUAGAGAGAAAAUUCAUCCCUCCUCAAACACACCUGUAGUCAAUGUAGGGACUGUGAUUUAUAAACAUCUAUCCCCUUCCUCUGUUUUGGCUGACUUAGUGACAACAAAACCCACAUCUCCAAUGGCUACCACCUCCACUCUGGGGAAUACAAGUGUUUCCACAUCAACUCCUGCCUUCCCAGAAACUAUGAUGACACAGCCAACUUCCUCCCUGACUUCUGGAUUAAGGGAGAUCAGUACCUCUCAAGAGACCAGCUCAGCAACAGAGAGAAGUGCUUCUCUUUCUGGAAUGCCCACUGGUGCUACUACUAAGGUCUCCAGAACAGAAGCCCUCUCCUUAGGCAGAACAUCCACCCCAGGUCCUGCUCAAUCCACAAUAUCACCAGAAAUCUCCACGGAAACCAUCACUAGAAUUUCUACUCCCCUCACCACGACAGGAUCAGCAGAAAUGACCAUCACCCCCAAAACAGGUCAUUCUGGGGCAUCCUCACAAGGUACCUUUACCUUGGACACAUCAAGCAGAGCCUCCUGGCCAGGAACUCACUCAGCUGCAACUCACAGAUCUCCACACUCAGGGAUGACCACUCCUAUGAGCAGAGGUCCUGAGGAUGUGUCAUGGCCAAGCCGCCCAUCAGUGGAAAAAACUAGCCCUCCAUCUUCCCUGGUGUCUUUAUCUGCAGUAACCUCACCUUCGCCACUUUAUUCCACACCAUCUGAGAGUAGCCACUCAUCUCCUCUCCGGGUGACUUCUCUUUUCACCCCUGUCAUGAUGAAGACCACAGACAUGUUGGACACAAGCUUGGAACCUGUGACCACUUCACCUCCCAGUAUGAAUAUCACCUCAGAUGAGAGUCUGGCCACUUCUAAAGCCACCAUGGAGACAGAGGCAAUUCAGCUUUCAGAAAACACAGCUGUGACUCAGAUGGGCACCAUCAGCGCUAGACAAGAAUUCUAUUCCUCUUAUCCAGGCCUCCCAGAGCCAUCCAAAGUGACAUCUCCAGUGGUCACCUCUUCCACCAUAAAAGACAUUGUUUCUACAACCAUACCUGCUUCCUCUGAGAUAACAAGAAUUGAGAUGGAGUCAACAUCCACCCUGACCCCCACACCAAGGGAGACCAGCACCUCCCAGGAGAUCCACUCAGCCACAAAGCCAAGCACUGUUCCUUACAAGGCACUCACUAGUGCCACGAUUGAGGACUCCAUGACACAAGUCAUGUCCUCUAGCAGAGGACCUAGCCCUGAUCAGUCCACAAUGUCACAAGACAUAUCCACUGAAGUGAUCACCAGGCUCUCUACCUCCCCCAUCAAGACAGAAUCUACAGAAAUGACCAUUACCACCCAAACAGGUUCUCCUGGGGCUACAUCAAGGGGUACCCUUACCUUGGACACUUCAACAACUUUUAUGUCAGGGACCCACUCAACUGCAUCUCAAGGAUUUUCACACUCACAGAUGACCGCUCUUAUGAGUAGAACUCCUGGAGAUGUGCCAUGGCUAAGCCAUCCCUCUGUGGAAGAAGCCAGCUCUGCCUCUUUCUCACUGUCUUCACCUGUCAUGACCUCAUCUUCUCCCGUUUCUUCCACAUUACCAGACAGCAUCCACUCUUCUUCGCUUCCUGUGACAUCACUUCUCACCUCAGGGCUGGUGAAGACCACAGAGCUGUUGGGCACAAGCUCAGAACCUGAAACCAGUUCACCCCCAAAUUUGAGCAGCACCUCAGCUGAAAUACUGGCCAUCACUGAAGUCACUACAGAUACAGAGAAACUGGAGAUGACCAAUGUGGUAACCUCAGGUUAUACACAUGAAUCUCCUUCCUCUGUCCUAGCUGACUCAGUGACAACAAAGGCCACAUCUUCAAUGGGUAUCACCUACCCCACAGGAGAUACAAAUGUUCUCACAUCAACCCCUGCCUUCUCUGACACCAGUAGGAUUCAAACAAAGUCAAAGCUCUCACUGACUCCUGGGUUGAUGGAGACCAGCAUCUCUGAAGAGACCAGCUCUGCCACAGAAAAAAGCACUGUCCUUUCUAGUGUGCCCACUGGUGCUACUACUGAGGUCUCCAGGACAGAAGCCAUCUCUUCUAGCAGAACAUCCAUCCCAGGCCCUGCUCAAUCCACAAUGUCAUCAGACACCUCCAUGGAAACCAUCACUAGAAUUUCUACCCCCCUCACAAGGAAAGAAUCAACAGACAUGGCCAUCACCCCCAAAACAGGUCCUUCUGGGGCUACCUCGCAGGGUACCUUUACCUUGGACUCAUCAAGCACAGCCUCCUGGCCAGGAACUCACUCAGCUACAACUCAGAGAUUUCCACAGUCAGUGGUGACAACUCCUAUGAGCAGAGGUCCUGAGGAUGUGUCAUGGCCAAGCCCGCUGUCUGUGGAAAAAAACAGCCCUCCAUCUUCCCUGGUAUCUUCAUCUUCAGUAACCUCACCUUCGCCACUUUAUUCCACACCAUCUGGGAGUAGCCACUCCUCUCCUGUCCCUGUCACUUCUCUUUUCACCUCUAUCAUGAUGAAGGCCACAGACAUGUUGGAUGCAAGUUUGGAACCUGAGACCACUUCAGCUCCCAAUAUGAAUAUCACCUCAGAUGAGAGUCUGGCCGCUUCUAAAGCCACCACGGAGACAGAGGCAAUUCACGUUUUUGAAAAUACAGCAGCGUCCCAUGUGGAAACCACCAGUGCUACAGAGGAACUCUAUUCCUCUUCCCCAGGCUUCUCAGAGCCAACAAAAGUGAUAUCUCCAGUGGUCACCUCUUCCUCUAUAAGAGACAACAUGGUUUCCACAACAAUGCCUGGCUCCUCUGGCAUUACAAGGAUUGAGAUAGAGUCAAUGUCAUCUCUGACCCCUGGACUGAGGGAGACCAGAACCUCCCAGGACAUCACCUCAUCCACAGAGACAAGCACUGUCCUUUACAAGAUGCCCUCUGGUGCCACUCCUGAGGUCUCCAGGACAGAAGUUAUGCCCUCUAGCAGAACAUCCAUUCCUGGCCCUGCUCAGUCCACAAUGUCACUAGACAUCUCCGAUGAAGUUGUCACCAGGCUGUCUACCUCUCCCAUCAUGACAGAAUCUGCAGAAAUAACCAUCACCACCCAAACAGGUUAUUCUCUGGCUACAUCCCAGGUUACCCUUCCCUUGGGCACCUCAAUGACCUUUUUGUCAGGGACCCACUCAACUAUGUCUCAAGGACUUUCACACUCAGAGAUGACCAAUCUUAUGAGCAGGGGUCCUGAAAGUCUGUCAUGGACGAGCCCUCGCUUUGUGGAAACAACUAGAUCUUCCUCUUCUCUGACAUCAUUACCUCUCACGACCUCACUUUCUCCUGUGUCCUCCACAUUACUAGACAGUAGCCCCUCCUCUCCUCUUCCUGUGACUUCACUUAUCCUCCCAGGCCUGGUGAAGACUACAGAAGUGUUGGAUACAAGCUCAGAGCCUAAAACCAGUUCAUCUCCAAAUUUGAGCAGCACCUCAGUUGAAAUACCGGCCACCUCUGAAAUCAUGACAGAUACAGAGAAAAUUCAUCCUUCCUCAAACACAGCGGUGGCCAAAGUGAGGACCUCCAGUUCUGUUCAUGAAUCUCAUUCCUCUGUCCUAGCUGACUCAGAAACAACCAUAACCAUACCUUCAAUGGGUAUCACCUCCGCUGUGGACGAUACCACUGUUUUCACAUCAAAUCCUGCCUUCUCUGAGACUAGGAGGAUUCCGACAGAGCCAACAUUCUCAUUGACUCCUGGAUUCAGGGAGACUAGCACCUCUGAAGAGACCACCUCAAUCACAGAAACAAGUGCAGUCCUUUAUGGAGUGCCCACUAGUGCUACUACUGAAGUCUCCAUGACAGAAAUCAUGUCCUCUAAUAGAAUACACAUCCCUGACUCUGAUCAGUCCACGAUGUCUCCAGACAUCAUCACUGAAGUGAUCACCAGGCUCUCUUCCUCAUCCAUGAUGUCAGAAUCAACACAAAUGACCAUCACCACCCAAAAAAGUUCUCCUGGGGCUACAGCACAGAGUACUCUUACCUUGGCCACAACAACAGCCCCCUUGGCAAGGACCCACUCAACUGUUCCUCCUAGAUUUUUACACUCAGAGAUGACAACUCUUAUGAGUAGGAGUCCUGAAAAUCCAUCAUGGAAGAGCUCUCUCUUUGUGGAAAAAACUAGCUCUUCAUCUUCUCUGUUGUCCUUACCUGUCACGACCUCACCUUCUGUUUCUUCCACAUUACCGCAGAGUAUCCCUUCCUCCUCUUUUUCUGUGACUUCACUCCUCACCCCAGGCAUGGUGAAGACUACAGACACAAGCACAGAACCUGGAACCAGUUUAUCUCCAAAUCUGAGUGGCACCUCAGUUGAAAUACUGGCUGCCUCUGAAGUCACCACAGAUACAGAGAAAAUUCAUCCUUCUUCAAGCAUGGCAGUGACCAAUGUGGGAACCACCAGUUCUGGACAUGAACUAUAUUCCUCUGUUUCAAUCCACUCGGAGCCAUCCAAGGCUACAUACCCAGUGGGUACUCCCUCUUCCAUGGCUGAAACCUCUAUUUCCACAUCAAUGCCUGCUAAUUUUGAGACCACAGGAUUUGAGGCUGAGCCAUUUUCUCAUUUGACUUCUGGAUUUAGGAAGACAAACAUGUCCCUGGACACCAGCUCAGUCACACCAACAAAUACACCUUCUUCUCCUGGGUCCACUCACCUUUUACAGAGUUCCAAGACUGAUUUCACCUCUUCUGCAAAAACAUCAUCCCCAGACUGGCCUCCAGCCUCACAGUAUACUGAAAUUCCAGUGGACAUAAUCACCCCCUUUAAUGCUUCUCCAUCUAUUACGGAGUCCACUGGGAUAACCUCCUUCCCAGAAUCCAGGUUUACUAUGUCUGUAACAGAAAGUACUCAUCAUCUGAGUACAGAUUUGCUGCCUUCAGCUGAGACUAUUUCCACUGGCACAGUGAUGCCUUCUCUAUCAGAGGCCAUGACUUCAUUUGCCACCACUGGAGUUCCACGAGCCAUCUCAGGUUCAGGUAGUCCAUUCUCUAGGACAGAGUCAGGCCCUGGGGAUGCUACUCUGUCCACCAUUGCAGAGAGCCUGCCUUCAUCCACUCCUGUGCCAUUCUCCUCUUCAACCUUCACUACCACUGAUUCUUCAACCAUCCCAGCCCUCCAUGAGAUAACUUCCUCUUCAGCUACCCCAUAUAGAGUGGACACCAGUCUUGGGACAGAGAGCAGCACUACUGAAGGACGCUUGGUUAUGGUCAGUACUUUGGACACUUCAAGCCAACCAGGCAGGACAUCUUCAUCACCCAUUUUGGAUACCAGAAUGACAGAGAGCGUUGAGCUGGGAACAGUGACAAGUGCUUAUCAAGUUCCUUCACUCUCAACACGGUUGACAAGAACUGAUGGCAUUAUGGAACACAUCACAAAAAUACCCAAUGAAGCAGCACACAGAGGUACCAUAAGACCAGUCAAAGGCCCUCAGACAUCCACUUCGCCUGCCAGUCCUAAAGGACUACACACAGGAGGGACAAAAAGAAUGGAGACCACCACCACAGCUCUGAAGACCACCACCACAGCUCUGAAGACCACUUCCAGAGCCACCUUGACCACCAGUGUCUAUACUCCCACUUUGGGAACACUGACUCCCCUCAAUGCAUCAAUGCAAAUGGCCAGCACAAUCCCCACAGAAAUGAUGAUCACAACCCCAUAUGUUUUCCCUGAUGUUCCAGAAACGACAUCCUCAUUGGCUACCAGCCUGGGAGCAGAAACCAGCACAGCUCUUCCCAGGACAACCCCAUCUGUUUUCAAUAGAGAAUCAGAGACCACAGCCUCACUGGUCUCUCGUUCUGGGGCAGAGAGAAGUCCGGUUAUUCAAACUCUAGAUGUUUCUUCUAGUGAGCCAGAUACAACAGCUUCAUGGGUUAUCCAUCCUGCAGAGACCAUCCCAACUGUUUCCAAGACAACCCCCAAUUUUUUCCACAGUGAAUUAGACACUGUAUCUUCCACAGCCACCAGUCAUGGGGCAGACGUCAGCUCAGCCAUUCCAACAAAUAUCUCACCUAGUGAACUAGAUGCACUGACCCCACUGGUCACUAUUUCGGGGACAGAUACUAGUACAACAUUCCCAACACUGACUAAGUCCCCACAUGAAACAGAGACAAGAACCACAUGGCUCACUCAUCCUGCAGAGACCAGCUCAACUAUUCCCAGAACAAUCCCCAAUUUUUCUCAUCAUGAAUCAGAUGCCACACCUUCAAUAGCCACCAGUCCUGGGGCAGAAACCAGUUCAGCUAUUCCAAUUAUGACUGUCUCACCUGGUGCAGAAGAUCUGGUGACCUCACAGGUCACUAGUUCUGGGACAGACAGAAAUAUGACUAUUCCAACUUUGACUCUUUCUCCUGGUGAACCAAAGACGAUAGCCUCAUUAGUCACCCAUCCUGAAGCACAGACAAGUUCGGCCAUUCCAACUUCAACUAUCUCGCCUGCUGUAUCACGGUUGGUGACCUCAAUGGUCACCAGUUUGGCGGCAAAGACAAGUACAACUAAUCGAGCUCUGACAAACUCCCCUGGUGAACCAGCUACAACAGUUUCAUUGGUCACGCAUCCUGCACAGACCAGCCCAACAGUUCCCUGGACAACUUCCAUUUUUUUCCAUAGUAAAUCAGACACCACACCUUCAAUGACCACCAGUCAUGGGGCAGAAUCCAGUUCAGCUGUUCCAACUCCAACUGUUUCAACUGAGGUACCAGGAGUAGUGACCCCUUUGGUCACCAGUUCUAGGGCAGUGAUCAGUACAACUAUUCCAAUUCUGACUCUUUCUCCUGGUGAACCAGAGACCACACCUUCAAUGGCCACCAGUCAUGGGGAAGAAGCCAGUUCUGCUAUUCCAACUCCAACUGUUUCACCUGGGGUACCAGGAGUGGUGACCUCUCUGGUCACUAGUUCUAGGGCAGUGACUAGUACAACUAUUCCAAUUCUGACUUUUUCUCUUGGUGAACCAGAGACCACACCUUCAAUGGCCACCAGUCAUGGGACAGAAGCUGGCUCAGCUGUUCCAACUGUUUUACCUGAGGUACCAGGAAUGGUGACCUCUCUGGUUGCUAGUUCUAGGGCAGUAACCAGUACAACUCUUCCAACUCUGACUCUUUCUCCUGGUGAACCAGAGACCACACCUUCAAUGGCCACCAGUCAUGGGGCAGAAGCCAGCUCAACUGUUCCAACUGUUUCACCUGAGGUACCAGGAGUGGUGACCUCUCUGGUCACUAGUUCUAGUGGAGUAAACAGUACAAGUAUUCCAACUCUGAUUCUUUCUCCUGGUGAACUAGAAACCACACCUUCAAUGGCCACCAGUCAUGGGGCAGAAGCCAGCUCAGCUGUUCCAACUCCAACUGUUUCACCUGGGGUAUCAGGAGUGGUGACCCCUCUGGUCACUAGUUCCAGGGCAGUGACCAGUACAACUAUUCCAAUUCUAACUCUUUCUUCUAGUGAGCCAGAGACCACACCUUCAAUGGCCACCAGUCAUGGGGUAGAAGCCAGCUCAGCUGUUCUAACUGUUUCACCUGAGGUACCAGGAAUGGUGACCUCUCUGGUCACUAGUUCUAGAGCAGUAACCAGUACAACUAUUCCAACUCUGACUAUUUCUUCUGAUGAACCAGAGACCACAACUUCAUUGGUCACCCAUUCUGAGGCAAAGAUGAUUUCAGCCAUUCCAACUUUAGCUGUCUCCCCUACUGUACAAGGGCUGGUGACUUCACUGGUCACUAGUUCUGGGUCAGAGACCAGUGCGUUUUCAAAUCUAACUGUUGCCUCAAGUCAACCAGAGACCAUAGACUCAUGGGUCGCUCAUCCUGGGACAGAAGCAAGUUCUGUUGUUCCAACUUUGACUGUCUCCACUGGUGAGCCGUUUACAAAUAUCUCAUUGGUCACCCAUCCUGCAGAGAGUAGCUCAACUCUUCCCAGGACAACCUCAAGGUUUUCCCACAGUGAAUUAGACACUAUGCCUUCUACAGUCACCAGUCCUGAGGCAGAAUCCAGCUCAGCCAUUUCAACAACUAUUUCACCUGGUAUACCAGGUGUGCUGACAUCACUGGUCACUAGCUCUGGGAGAGACAUCAGUGCAACUUUUCCAACAGUGCCUGAGUCCCCACAUGAAUCAGAGGCAACAGCCUCAUGGGUUACUCAUCCUGCAGUCACCAGCACAACAGUUCCCAGGACAACCCCUAAUUAUUCUCAUAGUGAACCAGACACCACACCAUCAAUAGCCACCAGUCCUGGGGCAGAAGCCACUUCAGAUUUUCCAACAAUAACUGUCUCACCUGAUGUACCAGAUAUGGUAACCUCACAGGUCACUAGUUCUGGGACAGACACCAGUAUAACUAUUCCAACUCUGACUCUUUCUUCUGGUGAGCCAGAGACCACAACCUCAUUUAUCACCUAUUCUGAGACACACACAAGUUCAGCCAUUCCAACUCUCCCUGUCUCCCCUGGUGCAUCAAAGAUGCUGACCUCACUGGUCAUCAGUUCUGGGACAGACAGCACUACAACUUUCCCAACACUGACGGAGACCCCAUAUGAACCAGAGACAACAGCCAUACAGCUCAUUCAUCCUGCAGAGACCAACACAAUGGUUCCCAGGACAACUCCCAAGUUUUCCCAUAGUAAGUCAGACACCACACUCCCAGUAGCCAUCACCAGUCCUGGGCCAGAAGCCAGUUCAGCUGUUUCAACGACAACUAUCUCACCUGAUAUGUCAGAUCUGGUGACCUCACUGGUCCCUAGUUCUGGGACAGACACCAGUACAACCUUCCCAACAUUGAGUGAGACCCCAUAUGAACCAGAGACUACAGCCACGUGGCUCACUCAUCCUGCAGAAACCAGCACAACGGUUUCUGGGACAAUUCCCAACUUUUCCCAUAGGGGAUCAGACACUGCACCCUCAAUGGUCACCAGUCCUGGAGUAGACACGAGGUCAGGUGUUCCAACUACAACCAUCCCACCCAGUAUACCAGGGGUAGUGACCUCACAGGUCACUAGUUCUGCAACAGACACUAGUACAGCUAUUCCAACUUUGACUCCUUCUCCUGGUGAACCAGAGACCACAGCCUCAUCAGCUACCCAUCCUGGGACACAGACUGGCUUCACUGUUCCAAUUCGGACUGUUCCCUCUAGUGAGCCAGAUACAAUGGCUUCCUGGGUCACUCAUCCUCCACAGACCAGCACACCUGUUUCCAGAACAACCUCCAGUUUUUCCCAUAGUAGUCCAGAUGCCACACCUGUAAUGGCCACCAGUCCUAGGACAGAAGCCAGUUCAGCUGUACUGACAACAAUCUCACCUGGUGCACCAGAGAUGGUGACUUCACAGAUCACUAGUUCUGGGGCAGCAACCAGUACAACUGUUCCAACUUUGACUCAUUCUCCUGGUAUGCCAGAGACCACAGCCUUAUUGAGCACCCAUCCCAGAACAGAGACAAGUAAAACAUUUCCUGCUUCAACUGUGUUUCCUCAAGUAUCAGAGACCACAGCCUCACUCACCAUUAGACCUGGUGCAGAGACUAGCACAGCUCUCCCAACUCAGACAACAUCCUCUCUCUUCACCCUACUUGUAACUGGAACCAGCAGAGUUGAUCUAAGUCCAACUGCUUCACCUGGUGUUUCUGCAAAAACAGCCCCACUUUCCACCCAUCCAGGGACAGAAACCAGCACAAUGAUUCCAACUUCAACUCUUUCCCUUGGUUUACUAGAGACUACAGGCUUACUGGCCACCAGCUCUUCAGCAGAGACCAGCACGAGUACUCUAACUCUGACUGUUUCCCCUGCUGUCUCUGGGCUUUCCAGUGCCUCUAUAACAACUGAUAAGCCCCAAACUGUGACCUCCUGGAACACAGAAACCUCACCAUCUGUAACUUCAGUUGGACCCCCAGAAUUUUCCAGGACUGUCACAGGCACCACUAUGACCUUGAUACCAUCAGAGAUGCCAACACCACCUAAAACCAGUCAUGGAGAAGGAGUGAGUCCAACCACUAUCUUGAGAACUACAAUGGUUGAAGCCACUAAUUUAGCUACCACAGGUUCCAGUCCCACUGUGGCCAAGACAACAACCACCUUCAAUACACUGGCUGGAAGCCUCUUUACUCCUCUGACCACACCUGGGAUGUCCACCUUGGCCUCUGAGAGUGUGACCUCAAGAACAAGUUAUAACCAUCGGUCCUGGAUCUCCACCACCAGCACUCCGAUGACCUCCAUGUUCUCUCCAAGGCCUCUCGUAUCUGUGAGCCCCACCCCCAGCGCUACAGGUUAUAACCGUCGGUACUGGACCCCUGCCACCAGCACUCCAGUGACUUCUACAUUCUCCCCAGGGAUUUCCACAUCCUCCAUCCCCAGCUCCACAGCAGCCACAGUCCCAUUCAUGGUGCCAUUCACCCUCAACUUCACCAUCACCAACCUGCAGUACGAGGAGGACAUGCGGCACCCUGGUUCCAGGAAGUUCAACGCCACAGAGAGAGAACUGCAGGGUCUGCUCAAACCCUUGUUCAGGAAUAGCAGUCUGGAAUACCUCUAUUCAGGCUGCAGACUAGCCUCACUCAGGCCAGAGAAGGAUAGCUCAGCCACGGCAGUGGAUGCCAUCUGCACACAUCGCCCUGACCCUGAAGACCUCGGACUGGACAGAGAGCGACUGUACUGGGAGCUGAGCAAUCUGACAAAUGGCAUCCAGGAGCUGGGCCCCUACACCCUGGACCGGAACAGUCUCUAUGUCAAUGGUUUCACCCAUCGAAGCUCUAUGCCCACCACCAGCACUCCUGGGACCUCCACAGUGGAUGUGGGAACCUCAGGGACUCCAUCCUCCAGCCCCAGCCCCACGACUGCUGGCCCUCUCCUGAUGCCGUUCACCCUCAACUUCACCAUCACCAACCUGCAGUACGAGGAGGACAUGCGUCGCACUGGCUCCAGGAAGUUCAACACCAUGGAGAGUGUCCUGCAGGGUCUGCUCAAGCCCUUGUUCAAGAACACCAGUGUUGGCCCUCUGUACUCUGGCUGCAGAUUGACCUUGCUCAGGCCCGAGAAAGAUGGGGCAGCCACUGGAGUGGAUGCCAUCUGCACCCACCGCCUUGACCCCAAAAGCCCUGGACUCAACAGGGAGCAGCUGUACUGGGAGCUAAGCAAACUGACCAAUGACAUUGAAGAGCUGGGCCCCUACACCCUGGACAGGAACAGUCUCUAUGUCAAUGGUUUCACCCAUCAGAGCUCUGUGUCCACCACCAGCACUCCUGGGACCUCCACAGUGGAUCUCAGAACCUCAGGGACUCCAUCCUCCCUCUCCAGCCCCACAAUUAUGGCUGCUGGCCCUCUCCUGGUACCAUUCACCCUCAACUUCACCAUCACCAACCUGCAGUAUGGGGAGGACAUGGGUCACCCUGGCUCCAGGAAGUUCAACACCACAGAGAGGGUCCUGCAGGGUCUGCUUGGUCCCAUAUUCAAGAACACCAGUGUUGGCCCUCUGUACUCUGGCUGCAGACUGACCUCUCUCAGGUCUGAGAAGGAUGGAGCAGCCACUGGAGUGGAUGCCAUCUGCAUCCAUCAUCUUGACCCCAAAAGCCCUGGACUCAACAGAGAGCGGCUGUACUGGGAGCUGAGCCAACUGACCAAUGGCAUCAAAGAGCUGGGCCCCUACACCCUGGACAGGAACAGUCUCUAUGUCAAUGGUUUCACCCAUCGGACCUCUGUGCCCACCAGCAGCACUCCUGGGACCUCCACAGUGGACCUUGGAACCUCAGGGACUCCAUUCUCCCUCCCAAGCCCCGCAACUGCUGGCCCUCUCCUGGUGCUGUUCACCCUCAACUUCACCAUCACCAACCUGAAGUAUGAGGAGGACAUGCAUCGCCCUGGCUCCAGGAAGUUCAACACCACUGAGAGGGUCCUGCAGACUCUGCUUGGUCCUAUGUUCAAGAACACCAGUGUUGGCCUUCUGUACUCUGGCUGCAGACUGACCUUGCUCAGGUCCGAGAAGGAUGGAGCAGCCACUGGAGUGGAUGCCAUCUGCACCCACCGUCUUGACCCCAAAAGCCCUGGAGUGGACAGGGAGCAGCUAUACUGGGAGCUGAGCCAGCUGACCAAUGGCAUCAAAGAGCUGGGCCCCUACACCCUGGACAGGAACAGUCUCUAUGUCAAUGGUUUCACCCAUUGGAUCCCUGUGCCCACCAGCAGCACUCCUGGGACCUCCACAGUGGACCUUGGGUCAGGGACUCCAUCCUCCCUCCCCAGCCCCACAACUGCUGGCCCUCUCCUGGUGCCGUUCACCCUCAACUUCACCAUCACCAACCUGAAGUACGAGGAGGACAUGCAUUGCCCUGGCUCCAGGAAGUUCAACACCACAGAGAGAGUCCUGCAGAGUCUGCUUGGUCCCAUGUUCAAGAACACCAGUGUUGGCCCUCUGUACUCUGGCUGCAGACUGACCUUGCUCAGGUCCGAGAAGGAUGGAGCAGCCACUGGAGUGGAUGCCAUCUGCACCCACCGUCUUGACCCCAAAAGCCCUGGAGUGGACAGGGAGCAGCUAUACUGGGAGCUGAGCCAGCUGACCAAUGGCAUCAAAGAGCUGGGUCCCUACACCCUGGACAGAAACAGUCUCUAUGUCAAUGGUUUCACCCAUCAGACCUCUGCGCCCAACACCAGCACUCCUGGGACCUCCACAGUGGACCUUGGGACCUCAGGGACUCCAUCCUCCCUCCCCAGCCCUACAUCUGCUGGCCCUCUCCUGGUGCCAUUCACCCUCAACUUCACCAUCACCAACCUGCAGUACGAGGAGGACAUGCAUCACCCAGGCUCCAGGAAGUUCAACACCACGGAGCGGGUCCUGCAGGGUCUGCUUGGUCCCAUGUUCAAGAACACCAGUGUCGGCCUUCUGUACUCUGGCUGCAGACUGACCUUGCUCAGGCCUGAGAAGAAUGGGGCAGCCACUGGAAUGGAUGCCAUCUGCAGCCACCGUCUUGACCCCAAAAGCCCUGGACUCAACAGAGAGCAGCUGUACUGGGAGCUGAGCCAGCUGACCCAUGGCAUCAAAGAGCUGGGCCCCUACACCCUGGACAGGAACAGUCUCUAUGUCAAUGGUUUCACCCAUCGGAGCUCUGUGGCCCCCACCAGCACUCCUGGGACCUCCACAGUGGACCUUGGGACCUCAGGGACUCCAUCCUCCCUCCCCAGCCCCACAACAGCUGUUCCUCUCCUGGUGCCGUUCACCCUCAACUUUACCAUCACCAAUCUGCAGUAUGGGGAGGACAUGCGUCACCCUGGCUCCAGGAAGUUCAACACCACAGAGAGGGUCCUGCAGGGUCUGCUUGGUCCCUUGUUCAAGAACUCCAGUGUCGGCCCUCUGUACUCUGGCUGCAGACUGAUCUCUCUCAGGUCUGAGAAGGAUGGGGCAGCCACUGGAGUGGAUGCCAUCUGCACCCACCACCUUAACCCUCAAAGCCCUGGACUGGACAGGGAGCAGCUGUACUGGCAGCUGAGCCAGAUGACCAAUGGCAUCAAAGAGCUGGGCCCCUACACCCUGGACCGGAACAGUCUCUACGUCAAUGGUUUCACCCAUCGGAGCUCUGGGCUCACCACCAGCACUCCUUGGACUUCCACAGUUGACCUUGGAACCUCAGGGACUCCAUCCCCCGUCCCCAGCCCCACAACUGCUGGCCCUCUCCUGGUGCCAUUCACCCUAAACUUCACCAUCACCAACCUGCAGUAUGAGGAGGACAUGCAUCGCCCUGGAUCUAGGAAGUUCAACGCCACAGAGAGGGUCCUGCAGGGUCUGCUUAGUCCCAUAUUCAAGAACUCCAGUGUUGGCCCUCUGUACUCUGGCUGCAGACUGACCUCUCUCAGGCCCGAGAAGGAUGGGGCAGCAACUGGAAUGGAUGCUGUCUGCCUCUACCACCCUAAUCCCAAAAGACCUGGGCUGGACAGAGAGCAGCUGUACUGGGAGCUAAGCCAGCUGACCCACAACAUCACUGAGCUGGGCCCCUACAGCCUGGACAGGGACAGUCUCUAUGUCAAUGGUUUCACCCAUCAGAACUCUGUGCCCACCACCAGUACUCCUGGGACCUCCACAGUGUACUGGGCAACCACUGGGACUCCAUCCUCCUUCCCCGGCCACACAGAGCCUGGCCCUCUCCUGAUACCAUUCACUUUCAACUUUACCAUCACCAACCUGCAUUAUGAGGAAAACAUGCAACACCCUGGUUCCAGGAAGUUCAACACCACGGAGAGGGUUCUGCAGGGUCUGCUCACGCCCUUGUUCAAGAACACCAGUGUUGGCCCUCUGUACUCUGGCUGCAGACUGACCUUGCUCAGACCUGAGAAGCAGGAGGCAGCCACUGGAGUGGACACCAUCUGUACCCACCGCGUUGAUCCCAUCGGACCUGGACUGGACAGAGAGCGGCUAUACUGGGAGCUGAGCCAGCUGACCAACAGCGUUACAGAGCUGGGCCCCUACACCCUGGACAGGGACAGUCUCUAUGUCAAUGGCUUCAACCCUUGGAGCUCUGUGCCAACCACCAGCACUCCUGGGACCUCCACAGUGCACCUGGCAACCUCUGGGACUCCAUCCUCCCUGCCUGGCCACACAGCCCCUGUCCCUCUCUUGAUACCAUUCACCCUCAACUUUACCAUCACCAACCUGCAUUAUGAAGAAAACAUGCAACACCCUGGUUCCAGGAAGUUCAACACCACGGAGAGGGUUCUGCAGGGUCUGCUCAAGCCCUUGUUCAAGAGCACCAGCGUUGGCCCUCUGUACUCUGGCUGCAGACUGACCUUGCUCAGACCUGAGAAACAUGGGGCAGCCACUGGAGUGGACGCCAUCUGCACCCUCCGCCUUGAUCCCACUGGUCCUGGACUGGACAGAGAGCGGCUAUACUGGGAGCUGAGCCAGCUGACCAACAGCGUUACAGAGCUGGGCCCCUACACCCUGGACAGGGACAGUCUCUAUGUCAAUGGCUUCACCCAUCGGAGCUCUGUGCCAACCACCAGUAUUCCUGGGACCUCUGCAGUGCACCUGGAAACCUCUGGGACUCCAGCCUCCCUCCCUGGCCACACAGCCCCUGGCCCUCUCCUGGUGCCAUUCACCCUCAACUUCACUAUCACCAACCUGCAGUAUGAGGAGGACAUGCGUCACCCUGGUUCCAGGAAGUUCAACACCACGGAGAGAGUCCUGCAGGGUCUGCUCAAGCCCUUGUUCAAGAGCACCAGUGUUGGCCCUCUGUACUCUGGCUGCAGACUGACCUUGCUCAGGCCUGAAAAACGUGGGGCAGCCACCGGCGUGGACACCAUCUGCACUCACCGCCUUGACCCUCUAAACCCUGGACUGGACAGAGAGCAGCUAUACUGGGAGCUGAGCAAACUGACCCGUGGCAUCAUCGAGCUGGGCCCCUACCUCCUGGACAGAGGCAGUCUCUAUGUCAAUGGUUUCACCCAUCGGAACUUUGUGCCCAUCACCAGCACUCCUGGGACCUCCACAGUACACCUAGGAACCUCUGAAACUCCAUCCUCCCUACCUAGACCCAUAGUGCCUGGCCCUCUCCUGGUGCCAUUCACCCUCAACUUCACCAUCACCAACUUGCAGUAUGAGGAGGCCAUGCGACACCCUGGCUCCAGGAAGUUCAAUACCACGGAGAGGGUCCUACAGGGUCUGCUCAGGCCCUUGUUCAAGAAUACCAGUAUCGGCCCUCUGUACUCCAGCUGCAGACUGACCUUGCUCAGGCCAGAGAAGGACAAGGCAGCCACCAGAGUGGAUGCCAUCUGUACCCACCACCCUGACCCUCAAAGCCCUGGACUGAACAGAGAGCAGCUGUACUGGGAGCUGAGCCAGCUGACCCACGGCAUCACUGAGCUGGGCCCCUACACCCUGGACAGGGACAGUCUCUAUGUCGAUGGUUUCACUCAUUGGAGCCCCAUACCAACCACCAGCACUCCUGGGACCUCCAUAGUGAACCUGGGAACCUCUGGGAUCCCACCUUCCCUCCCUGAAACUACAGCCACCGGCCCUCUCCUGGUGCCAUUCACACUCAACUUCACCAUCACUAACCUACAGUAUGAGGAGAACAUGGGUCACCCUGGCUCCAGGAAGUUCAACAUCACGGAGAGUGUUCUGCAGGGUCUGCUCAAGCCCUUGUUCAAGAGCACCAGUGUUGGCCCUCUGUAUUCUGGCUGCAGACUGACCUUGCUCAGGCCUGAGAAGGAUGGAGUAGCCACCAGAGUGGACGCCAUCUGCACCCACCGCCCUGACCCCAAAAUCCCUGGGCUAGACAGACAGCAGCUAUACUGGGAGCUGAGCCAGCUGACCCACAGCAUCACUGAGCUGGGACCCUACACCCUGGAUAGGGACAGUCUCUAUGUCAAUGGUUUCACCCAGCGGAGCUCUGUGCCCACCACCAGCACUCCUGGGACUUUCACAGUACAGCCGGAAACCUCUGAGACUCCAUCAUCCCUCCCUGGCCCCACAGCCACUGGCCCUGUCCUGCUGCCAUUCACCCUCAAUUUUACCAUCACUAACCUGCAGUAUGAGGAGGACAUGCGUCGCCCUGGCUCCAGGAAGUUCAACACCACGGAGAGGGUCCUUCAGGGUCUGCUUAUGCCCUUGUUCAAGAACACCAGUGUCAGCUCUCUGUACUCUGGUUGCAGACUGACCUUGCUCAGGCCUGAGAAGGAUGGGGCAGCCACCAGAGUGGAUGCUGUCUGCACCCAUCGUCCUGACCCCAAAAGCCCUGGACUGGACAGAGAGCGGCUGUACUGGAAGCUGAGCCAGCUGACCCACGGCAUCACUGAGCUGGGCCCCUACACCCUGGACAGGCACAGUCUCUAUGUCAAUGGUUUCACCCAUCAGAGCUCUAUGACGACCACCAGAACUCCUGAUACCUCCACAAUGCACCUGGCAACCUCGAGAACUCCAGCCUCCCUGUCUGGACCCAUGACCGCCAGCCCUCUCCUGGUGCUAUUCACAAUUAACUUCACCAUCACUAACCUGCGGUAUGAGGAGAACAUGCAUCACCCUGGCUCUAGAAAGUUUAACACCACGGAGAGAGUCCUUCAGGGUCUGCUCAGGCCUGUGUUCAAGAACACCAGUGUUGGCCCUCUGUACUCUGGCUGCAGACUGACCUUGCUCAGGCCCAAGAAGGAUGGGGCAGCCACCAAAGUGGAUGCCAUCUGCACCUACCGCCCUGAUCCCAAAAGCCCUGGACUGGACAGAGAGCAGCUAUACUGGGAGCUGAGCCAGCUGACCCACAGCAUCACUGAGCUGGGCCCCUACACCCUGGACAGGGACAGUCUCUAUGUCAAUGGUUUCACACAGCGGAGCUCUGUGCCCACCACUAGCAUUCCUGGGACCCCCACAGUGGACCUGGGAACAUCUGGGACUCCAGUUUCUAAACCUGGUCCCUCGGCUGCCAGCCCUCUCCUGGUGCUAUUCACUCUCAACUUCACCAUCACCAACCUGCGGUAUGAGGAGAACAUGCAGCACCCUGGCUCCAGGAAGUUCAACACCACGGAGAGGGUCCUUCAGGGCCUGCUCAGGUCCCUGUUCAAGAGCACCAGUGUUGGCCCUCUGUACUCUGGCUGCAGACUGACUUUGCUCAGGCCUGAAAAGGAUGGGACAGCCACUGGAGUGGAUGCCAUCUGCACCCACCACCCUGACCCCAAAAGCCCUAGGCUGGACAGAGAGCAGCUGUAUUGGGAGCUGAGCCAGCUGACCCACAAUAUCACUGAGCUGGGCCCCUAUGCCCUGGACAACGACAGCCUCUUUGUCAAUGGUUUCACUCAUCGGAGCUCUGUGUCCACCACCAGCACUCCUGGGACCCCCACAGUGUAUCUGGGAGCAUCUAAGACUCCAGCCUCGAUAUUUGGCCCUUCAGCUGCCAGCCAUCUCCUGAUACUAUUCACCCUCAACUUCACCAUCACUAACCUGCGGUAUGAGGAGAACAUGUGGCCUGGCUCCAGGAAGUUCAACACUACAGAGAGGGUCCUUCAGGGCCUGCUAAGGCCCUUGUUCAAGAACACCAGUGUUGGCCCUCUGUACUCUGGCUGCAGGCUGACCUUGCUCAGGCCAGAGAAAGAUGGGGAAGCCACCGGAGUGGAUGCCAUCUGCACCCACCGCCCUGACCCCACAGGCCCUGGGCUGGACAGAGAGCAGCUGUAUUUGGAGCUGAGCCAGCUGACCCACAGCAUCACUGAGCUGGGCCCCUACACACUGGACAGGGACAGUCUCUAUGUCAAUGGUUUCACCCAUCGGAGCUCUGUACCCACCACCAGCACCGGGGUGGUCAGCGAGGAGCCAUUCACACUGAACUUCACCAUCAACAACCUGCGCUACAUGGCGGACAUGGGCCAACCCGGCUCCCUCAAGUUCAACAUCACAGACAACGUCAUGCAGCACCUGCUCAGUCCUUUGUUCCAGAGGAGCAGCCUGGGUGCACGGUACACAGGCUGCAGGGUCAUCGCACUAAGGUCUGUGAAGAACGGUGCUGAGACACGGGUGGACCUCCUCUGCACCUACCUGCAGCCCCUCAGCGGCCCAGGUCUGCCUAUCAAGCAGGUGUUCCAUGAGCUGAGCCAGCAGACCCAUGGCAUCACCCGGCUGGGCCCCUACUCUCUGGACAAAGACAGCCUCUACCUUAACGGUUACAAUGAACCUGGUCCAGAUGAGCCUCCUACAACUCCCAAGCCAGCCACCACAUUCCUGCCUCCUCUGUCAGAAGCCACAACAGCCAUGGGGUACCACCUGAAGACCCUCACACUCAACUUCACCAUCUCCAAUCUCCAGUAUUCACCAGAUAUGGGCAAGGGCUCAGCUACAUUCAACUCCACCGAGGGGGUCCUUCAGCACCUGCUCAGACCCUUGUUCCAGAAGAGCAGCAUGGGCCCCUUCUACUUGGGUUGCCAACUGAUCUCCCUCAGGCCUGAGAAGGAUGGGGCAGCCACUGGUGUGGACACCACCUGCACCUACCACCCUGACCCUGUGGGCCCCGGGCUGGACAUACAGCAGCUUUACUGGGAGCUGAGUCAGCUGACCCAUGGUGUCACCCAACUGGGCUUCUAUGUCCUGGACAGGGAUAGCCUCUUCAUCAAUGGCUAUGCACCCCAGAAUUUAUCAAUCCGGGGCGAGUACCAGAUAAAUUUCCACAUUGUCAACUGGAACCUCAGUAAUCCAGACCCCACAUCCUCAGAGUACAUCACCCUGCUGAGGGACAUCCAGGACAAGGUCACCACACUCUACAAAGGCAGUCAACUACAUGACACAUUCCGCUUCUGCCUGGUCACCAACUUGACGAUGGACUCCGUGUUGGUCACUGUCAAGGCAUUGUUCUCCUCCAAUUUGGACCCCAGCCUGGUGGAGCAAGUCUUUCUAGAUAAGACCCUGAAUGCCUCAUUCCAUUGGCUGGGCUCCACCUACCAGUUGGUGGACAUCCAUGUGACAGAAAUGGAGUCAUCAGUUUAUCAACCAACAAGCAGCUCCAGCACCCAGCACUUCUACCUGAAUUUCACCAUCACCAACCUACCAUAUUCCCAGGACAAAGCCCAGCCAGGCACCACCAAUUACCAGAGGAACAAAAGGAAUAUUGAGGAUGCGCUCAACCAACUCUUCCGAAACAGCAGCAUCAAGAGUUAUUUUUCUGACUGUCAAGUUUCAACAUUCAGGUCUGUCCCCAACAGGCACCACACCGGGGUGGACUCCCUGUGUAACUUCUCGCCACUGGCUCGGAGAGUAGACAGAGUUGCCAUCUAUGAGGAAUUUCUGCGGAUGACCCGGAAUGGUACCCAGCUGCAGAACUUCACCCUGGACAGGAGCAGUGUCCUUGUGGAUGGGUAUUCUCCCAACAGAAAUGAGCCCUUAACUGGGAAUUCUGACCUUCCCUUCUGGGCUGUCAUCCUCAUCGGCUUGGCAGGACUCCUGGGAGUCAUCACAUGCCUGAUCUGCGGUGUCCUGGUGACCACCCGCCGGCGGAAGAAGGAAGGAGAAUACAACGUCCAGCAACAGUGCCCAGGCUACUACCAGUCACACCUAGACCUGGAGGAUCUGCAAUGACUGGAACUUGCCGGUGCCUGGGGUGCCUUUCCCCCAGCCAGGGUCCAAAGAAGCUUGGCUGGGGCAGAAAUAAACCAUAUUGGUCGGA